GAUUCAUCUGCCAACUAGGGUCUCCAUCUGGUUUGGAUUGGAUUGAGAUUGGAUAACACCUUUCCACCUAAUAGCAGCAUUAAGAGCAUUGACUGCCAAAAGCCAUAGCUAACCUACUUUCUUUAGGAUACAUAUUGUUUCUCCUCAUUACCCUGUAAUAAAAUAAGAUUUAUCUUAAGCAUGUCCUGAGAGAAGCCUAAAAUGGAAAUACACGGUACAGGCAUCGUAAGCUGGGAGAGACCUGAAGGACCAUUGGCAGCCCCCUGAAUUGUAACUGAGGAAAUGGCUCUGUCAGAUUGAGAUCUGCAUUAGUGGCCUAGUUGUGGAGUGACGUAGGGAGUGAGUGUAUGAGCAGAGCAUGUGUGGUGUUCAUUCCCAUCCAUCCAUCACUCAUCCUACAUGAAGUUGCCUCUGGAUUGGGACCUUGAACUCUACUAAUUUUAUGGUAGUGUAACUUGCAGAAGACUUACCAGGUAGGUGAGCUUGGUAGUAUGUUUUGUUUUGUUUUGCAUUUGGGACCAUCUUCACAUGUGUCAACUAAGAAGGAUUUGCUGCUAACCUAUACCUAAAUCUCUGACACAAAUCCUGGAAAAGCCUUAAAUGAUUGGCAGGUAGUGUUGAAAGGUGCUGUAUCAGGGUUUUGUAAAUCAUGCCAUCUAGAUAGAAUGCAUUGUGUUGGAAUGAAAUUAAAACAACCAUUUUAAAAAAUGUAAAUGACCUUGGGUAGAAAAACACGAGCAUUAAGCUGUAUUAGCAGGUGAAGAUAAAUCUCUCCCCCUUCAUGUUUGAAAUAAUCUUUUACAUUGUUUAUGUGAAUUUCUUUCUUUUUUUCGGGUACAUUGAUUAUGUAUCUUCCCCCACCCUCCACAUUUAAUCCCCUAAGGGAUCGGUAUUAAUGAGUUUUAUGCUUUGAAUUUUAAAAUUUUCUUGUCCUCAAAAGUGAGACUGGGGAAAAAGAGAAAAGACUUUAAACAUUUUCUUUGAAAGCUUUUAGUUAUCUCAUAUACCUAUUCCUUUUGAAAAUUUCUCUGUGGAUAGCCGGCUUAGUUUCUUGCAAAUGACUAAUUUAAAUGCCAUAGAACAUGUUUAGAUUCACUGUCACAUGGUUGUUCUUGCUACAUUUCUUUUGCUCAGAUUCAUCUUCAGAAAGUGAGGGAGGGGGAAAGCAUAUUAAGCAUAUUAUUCCUGCAAUUAAGGCAUAGAUUGGCUACUUAAUUUGUAGUUAGUAAAAAACUACUGUGAUGGAACUCAAAAUAUUAAUAAAUUGAGAAAACCAGAAUGCUUGUCUUUUGCUUUAGUGAUGGGACUAAGGUUUACAUGAAUCUUUCUAUGUCAUGUAGUUUCAGCUAGUGCCUCUUGGCUCUGAAAGCUAUGCAUAUGUAAUUUCAUUAUUAUUGAUAACAUAGUACCUCUCUAGAGAGUUCUAGUUACUGUAUUUUUAAAAUGCAAACAUUUGAAAAUGUAGAUACAAUUCUAUUUUUUAAAAUUAAUAGGUCUGAACUGGGAUCUUUGGUGAUAUUUCCAUUUCAAAGUAUUUAUCAAAUCAAGACAUUAGUGGUAAAACAGUACUAGUACAAAGAUGCUUAGGUAUUGCUCUAUAUUUUUCAAAAGAAUAACAAAGCAAGAACAACAUCUUUUAGAAACGUGUCUAAAAAGGUGCCAAUGUGACCAAAAAACCCAUUUAAUCACUGAGAAUUUUAACAGAAAUUUUUUAAAGUAUUAUAUUGCAGGAUCAAUAUUUAGUAUAUUGGACAAUUCAGAAGAUUUAUUCAGGUUUGCUUGGGGAUUGAGAACAAAUACGUGUUUAAAUCUGUAUGUAUAAUUUAAAAAUAUUAGAGAAAAUUUGAAAAAUAGGGAAGAGUCAGCCAUAUUGUUUUAAUUAAACAAAAUGACUGCUUCUGUUUUAGCAGUGCUUCCACUUUGUUUUCUAUGCGUUAUCUUUUUGAAGCCACUGGUUAAUGUAUGUAUAAAGCUUGCCAGCUUGUUUUUGAUUAACAAAGUUCAGUCAGUGAAUAAUGUAAAAUACUAUUAACAGCAUAACUGGAAAGUGACUUGAGCACAUAAAAAUCACCUUUAAGUCCAAAGUUAAAUUCUUGUUUUUAUGUUAUUUAUUGUUUUUAUUUAGAGAAGAGAUACGUGCCUCAUCUUAGGAAUUCUCAUUUAAUAUCCUUCAAAGACUGGGCUUUAAUGAACAAAUUUGUCAUGUGGCAGAAGUUACUGUAGUCUGAUGAAAGGGAAGAUGGCUGCAAAGAAGAGAAAACGGGUGGUGGGGGGCAUUGAGGUAUAAUAAUCUGUGGCUGUGGGAUGGUUUUCGACAGACCAGUCAUAGCCCAGACUCAUGUUUCCAAACAUACAUUAACUGCAAACCCUGAUCUCAGGUUUUAUGUUUUUCCAUCACUUUUUAGCUUUAAUUUGUAGUAGAUUGCUUGAGGAAAGACCCCUGUUGAUUGGUUGUAAUCAUCUAAGAUUUAUGAUGAUUAGGAAGUCUAAAUAAAAGUCUGUUAGAUCCAAUUUGGACAUAAAUUUUGAAUGCCCAGUUUAUUGGAUUGCCUUGAAAUUCUAAUUGGUAAUAUGCAAAUCGAGUUAGAGUCUUGACUAUCAAAAUCACCUUAGGACUAAAUUAGACAGUUUGGAAGCUCCAUUAACUCUUUCAGAGUACUGAACUACUAUUUAGUCUACCCAAACAGUAAUUUACUAAGUUUAGCAUACCCAGACAGUAAUUUGCAAAGUAAUACUUUGAAGAUGCUGGAAGGAGUUAAUGAAGCUUCUGAAAUAUUGUGUUUUUUGGGAGAAUCUGACUCAGCAUUUGCAGUAGUUGGAGUUGAGAAAGGGCGUCUUUAAAUUUUGGAUGCCUAAUUGGCAGGAAUUGUUGCUAAUGCUACAGUCUUUGAUUUUUAUCAUACUCCUACGCUCUUCCUGUCAUGUUGCAGACUCCUUUUACUAAUCUAUGUGAGUGCCCCCCAAGGUAAAGCCCCUGUGCACUUCCGUGGUGAUGCCUUCUGACUGGUUCAGCCUGUCACCUUGACACACACACAGAUGGUUUCUGGAGGCCGAUUUAAUUCCAGCUAUCUUGUUCUUCACCUCUCGUGUCCAUUUCUCUCCAUCUUUUCUCCUGAGCUUUGGUCUAAUUUGUCAACUCAGUGGGGACCAGUUGGCUGGCUGUUGCCUUGAACUUGUCUUCCUCUUUGAAAUGGGUUUCUCCUCCUGAAGUCAUCAGGUUUUGAAUAGCACUUACCAUAAUUUUUUAGGUGAGGAUAGUUUUCAGCGCUGGGUCAGUGGGAAAAACUCCAGUUCAACUCUGUUGCCUCCACAGUAGAGCAUGGAGUUGAAGCUUCUUGGAGUUUUCCUCUUUCUCUUCCCCUGGUUGGCUGGAACCAUUUCAUCAUUUCAUACUUGGGUCACUACACUGGUCUUUUCAUCGGCUUGCUGCCUCCAGUUUCCUCCUUCACUCUGCUGUGGGCAAGAUGACACAUCACUUUAAUUAUAACAUUUCACCUCCUGAAGCAUCUUCAGACACUCUGCUACUUUGAGGAUAAAAUCUAAAUCCUUUUGCUGGGCAUCAAGACCACUCACCAUCUGAAAGGCCCAUCUUUCCAGCUUCCUUUCCUACAGAUUCCUCUACCACCCCUCCGAGGCCGGAGGAGGGGCACUCCCUCCCUUUGAGGUAUUUUACACUUUUCUGUGCUCCUAGCAGGGCAUCCCUUUUCCGUACCCACCCUAUCUAGAACCACUCAAUGAAAAAAGCCAGGCUCACAAAGACACAUGCCACACGAUUCCAUUUGUAUAAAUUUCAAUAAACAAAACGAACAUAAGUGCUAGUAAGUGACAGUACCUGUGAGUGGUGGUUUCACAGGGUCCACGUACAAAACUUCGUCCAGCUGUACACAGCCCAUUUGAGCCUUUGGCUGUGUGUAAAUUAGACCUCAGUAAAACAGUGCCAAUCGUGUAAGGCUGUGGUGAGGCUUAAAUUAUAUAGUGUAGUAUAUAAAAUGCUGAGGGCAAGGCCUGGCAUGUGGGGGAAAUCCCAUCUCUUUUAGACAGAAGCAGUCGCUCUCAUUCUGAAUUGUAUAGUAGAUAAAUUCUUCCCUGACAAGACUAACUCUGCAAACAGACCUUGGAAGCUUUUUUUUUUUUUCAGCGUGUUUUUCACUUGACUUUUAUUGCCAUGUUUUGUUCAGUUGGUAUCUUUGGUUUAAUGUGGAUAUACUUGUUUUUUUUUUUUCUUGUUUAUAGUGUAAAUUUUUGAUCAAUAGAAAUAAUGGCAGUAGGGUGUGUUGUAGAAAGCUCUUAAUGGAAUAAGCAAUUCUCCCUUCCCCCAAAACAUUGUACAUAUCAAAAAGAACUUUAUCUUAAAAGUGUUUCAUACAACAAACAAGAUUUAUUUUCCCAAGUCAUCUAGUUACCAGAGAAGCAUCCAUAAAUGGUACUUAGUAGGAAGACAUAUGACUAAGGAAGACUUUCUUAAUUGAGCUGUGAAAAUGAAAUAAUAAACCAUUUUGCGAGAUGGCAAACUUCAGUGUAUAUAUUAAUCACCUGGGGAUCUUGUCAGUUCUGAUUUAGUAGGUCUGGGCUGAAGCCCAAGGUCCUGCAUUUGUAACCAGCUCCUAGUGAUGCCAGUGCUGCUGGCCUCAGAACCACACUGGGAGUAGAGCAGAGCUGGGGGUGUAUUCAGGUUCAGAGAUGGGACAUUAGGAAGGGCAAAACAAGAACUUAGCUCAUAAAAACCACCCCACAAAUUUGGGUGGGUAGUGACCUUGUGAACCACAUAUAUGUAAAUAUUCCUGAAAGAAUCUAUUCAAGAAAGUAUCAACUUGUGUUUUAAAGUUUUGAUGUUGUGUGAUUUUUUUUUUGUGCUAGUGGAAAAGACUGGUUGAUUUCAUUAGUUUGUUUUUGUUCAUUCGUUUGUUUUUGUUCCCUCUUGCAAAUAAUAUAUCAGAAAUGGUCAUGAAUUCAAUCAGAAUUUUAGGGAAAGAAAUUUAUUUGUGUGAAUGCCCCUUCUUUAAAGAAACAGUAACAACAUCAACAGAAAAGCCCCAAAAACUGAACUAAAAACUACCAUCCUGCCCAUUUGUUACUGUAUUUAAUGCAUCAUACUUGACAAAGUUGCUACCCUGUGCCAUAUUCCACCUGAAGAGCCAGUUUCGCCGGUGUUCUGUCUGCUCACUUAACCAUGAGUAGAUUUCCAUUUCCCUCCUCUGAACUGGGGCCUCUUUCAUUCGCUUGUUCCGUUUUGCCUAUCACAGUCUUGACUUGGUAGAGGAUUUUAUUCCCUGUCAGUCUUCAACCUCUGUUAGCCUAUGAUUUGAAACUGAGAAAAGUCCAAGUUGGAAAUUGAAAACGAGAGCCCGAUUCUCUGAGGCUGGGAAAGCCUCUGAGGACUUGGCCCGAGCACCGCCCGCCACCAUAACAGGUUAACAGGAAGAAUGUGGCUCUGCCUGCCGGCUCCUGGGCACAUUCCUUUCUGUUUGGGGACUGAAGUACUGGACACACACAUUAUUAAAUUACUUAAUGAAGAUUUUGAAGCACACCUCUAAUCCCUUUGAAAAGGCCCUUUGAGCUGGAGAAGGGUGUGUGGGCAGUGAGAGAGAGGCGCCUUCACCCUGGUGAACAGGGCCCCUUAGAAGCUCCCAGGGUGCGAGUCAGCAGCGUUCCAAGGCUGACCAUUACUUUCUGCCCUGAAUUGGCAGAAGAGACUUAGGGGAAAGUUCUUUCUAGGGCAGGACCCUUCACCGGGGGAAGAUGUAGGGUUUAGGCUCCAACCUUGACUCAGCAUUGCCAUUUACCAUUUUGGCACAGGACCUUGUUGAAGCCAUGACUAAGGGCCUCCAGGUGGUGGGCUGUCCUUUACAGGUCCUGAUCACAGUUAGGGAUGCAGCUCGGACUGAUAAAAAAGGGCCUUGGGCUCUGUCAGAAAUGUGUGUAGUUGAAUUACAUAGGUGAUUCUGAUAAUAAAGAUGUUUUUGUGUUCCCACUACCCUCUUAUUGGGAAGAUGUCUGCCUUAGAAAAUAAGAGAACAGGCUCCAAGGCUGGGUGACCAGGAACUCAUCUCUGGCAACAAACUCCAAUAGCCUUUGUCUUUAUCUGUGGUAAUAAUAAUUAUAAUAGUCCUAAUACAUUCUGGGGUUAUGGUGGUGAUUGAUUGAGAAUGUAUAAGGAAAGACUAGAUAUUAAAGCAUUAAUCACGUGUAACUGUCUGUAAACAGCGGUUUUGUAGUUUUUUGCUUUUAGUAAAUAGGCUCCCCCGUGUGAUCAAUACUAAACUGACAGCAAAAGAGCAGUCCAUUCUUAUUAGACCAUGCUUGGGGAGAUAAGUUGCUGCUGGCUCAUGAAGGACACAUUCUUCUUGAUGUAGGGAGGUGGAAUGAGGAUUUAGGCGCUGUCUUCCUCCCCUUUGGGGUAGGGUACCUUGCUGUCUUUUGACAGAAUGAGGAUGAGAGGAGGUGGUAGGAAGGCGGGGGAGGAUCAGUGAUGAGAUGGCACUGGGGACAGUGGAGAGAAUGGUUGUGCAUAUGAUUUACGGUCUUUCUUUUCAGUAUACUACAGUGCUUAGAUGUGUAUGCAGAAAUCAAGAGUUAUCAGUGAUGUUUGAAAAUUAGAUGUUGCUGGCAUGGAACUUCCGUUUUCAUUGAGAACAGAGCGUGCUUAGUGACGUGUAUAUUUAGUACAGUAAGACAGUUGCAGAAGGAUGGCCCUGAUGGUGACAGUGAUAAUCCUAACCCUAGAUGCUCACUGGCUGGGCACAAGUACAGGAUCUCACUGGAACCUCACUAGGUAUCUGUUGUCCUCCUUUUAUAGUUGAGAAAGAGAAAGCUUAAGUAAUUUGCCCAAGAUCAUGUAACUAAUAACUGGCAGGGAUUUGAGUCAGGAUCUCCAAAGCUACAUCUCUUCCUAAAGCUAGUUUUAAAAUUUCAUUUCUCAUAUAUGGAGUAGCCCACAAAGGCUGUAUGCAAGGUAGUCUUCAGAAAGCUUACAUCUUCACCAAGGCACAUGAAACUGCAGAAAGAAGCAAUGUUAGGCGUUCCUGAUAAUAAUUAUCUGCCUGGAUGACAGCAGUCCUGCUUUAUGGUCACAGACCCCAGCUUUCUGCCAGAACAUGGCUCAGGACUCCUGAAAAUCAUCCCAUUCGGGAGCAAGUGGGUUUAAUUUCCUUUUCAUGAAAGGAAAGAUUAGCUUUCAUGCAAACACUUGGUCCAUUUGGCCAUUUAAUAAGAAGACUGAAGUCUCAUGUUCCAUAACUUUAUCAGCCUAAAAGUCCCUUUGUUGUAUCAUAAACACAUAGGCUGAAACCCCUGUCCUUCCAACUCAGAGCAAAUUCUGUUGUAUUAAAUAACCAUGCCAUGUACUGAAUGUUUUUACACUUAUUUAUUGGACUUGACUCCUACCUCCUUCCCGCAAAAAAAAAAAAAAAAAAAAUUAGCUGACAUUUCUACAGGGCCUACGACUAACCAGAGGGAAAGAGACUCACAUGUCACUGUUUGUAGCCAGCAGUCCAAAUUGUGAAAUAAACAUACUUUGAAAUGUGGUCAUAAAAUACCUCCUGUAUUUUAUGGCCCACAGAGAAAUGACAAAUGUUUGAGGUGAUAUGCUCAGAAGAGCAUAGAAGUGAUCAGGGUGGGUCAUUUUGUUAACCGUUCAAGGAUGGAGAUUCUGUGUUCAAGGAAUCAGAGGAAAUUGUGAAUUUAUUUGAAUUUCUGUUACUGUUCACUUGAUAAUUUUAUAGUUGUCUUAGUGGCCCUUCUAACAGAAUAUGCCCCUUUAUGAAAUAUUACCACCCCUGCCCCGUUUUACCCUGAUUUGAUCAUUAUACACUGUAUACAUGUAUCAUAGUGUUACUCAGUACUCCAUAAUUAUGUUUAAUUAUCAUGUGUCAGUUUAGAUAAAAUUGUAGCAUGGACCAUUGACAUCAGUAUCACCAGGAAAUCUCAGGCCCACCCCCAGACAAUACUGAACGAGGAUCUGCGUUUUGACAGGAUAGAUAGAUCCCUGAUGAUCCCUUGUAUGUUCAAGUAUGAGAAGCACUGAUUUUUAUGGUACUCAGUCCCCCUCCAACUUACUGGUUAGGCUUAUAGAAUGGAGGCUUUAUUCUUUACAAAGUGUGUCAAGCUCUUUUAAAGCUAGGCUUUAGAGAACAAAAGUCCAAGUGUACCUGUUUAGCAUCAGGGCUGUUUUGCAUUUCUAGCAAAGUCUGACUUAUUAAACCUCCUAAUCGCUCCAUCUCAGUUUUUUCUGUUUACGUUGUAUUUCAUUUGCAAUGUGAAGCUAUUAGGAUGUUCCUUUUGUGAGGGAAAAGGAGGGAUAGAUUCCAUCUUAGUUCUCAUAAAAGUAUAAAAAUCAAAACCAAAUAAGCAUAUAUAAAGUCUACUGUAUGCUGGUGCGGUGGCUCAUACCUAUAAUCUCAGCACUUUGGGAGGUCAAAGUAGGAGGGUCGCUUGAGCCCAGAAGUUUGAGACUAGUCUGGGCAACAUAGUGAGACCUUGUCUCUAGAAAAAAUAAAAGAAAUUAGCUGGCUUGGUGGCUUGCACCUGUAGUCCUAGCUACUUGGGAGGCUGAGGCAAGAGGAUAGCUUGAGCCUAGGAGUUGGAAGCUGCAAGUGAGCCAUGAUUGUACCACUGCAUUCCAGCCUGGGUGUCAGAGCAAGACCCUGUCUCUAAAACAGAAUCUCCUGUAGAUGGCAUGGAGGAGAGAAGCCCGUGUGUAUUAUCCAGAACCCUCGCUCCCUGACGCCUUCUCCCCUGCCUUCAUCUUGUGCUCUUUAUUGGAGAAAAGUGUGAGGUGAACGCACAGAAAGGUGCUCCCCACUGUGGCAGGUUGAACGUUUGUUUUUGUUAAUUAAUGUCCAUGCAUUCUGCUCUUUCAGUAACUAGAUUUAGGUAACCUGGGCCUGUUUCCCAUCACUUCCUGGCCUUGUGACUGGGCAAAUAACUUUGUCUCCCUGGGCCUCAGUUUCCUUAACCCUGAAAUGAAGGGGUUAGAUUCCAGCGCUUUGCAUUCUCUGGCCAGCUCUUGAGCACCUGCGACUCCUUCCUGCUCUUCAGUUCUUCCUCCAUCCUGGCUGACUUUUGCUUGGCUCCCGCUGCCCCCAUUGGCCCCCUUAAACUCCAGAAGAGCAUAGAAGUGAUCAGGUGGGUCUUUUUGUUCACUAUCCAUUAACUUUUCAAGGAGGGAGAUGCUGUGUUCAAGGAGUCAGAGGUGAAAUUGUGAGUUUAUCUGAUUUUCUGUUCACUUGAUAAUUAUAUAGUUGACUUGGAAGUGUUUCAAACUGAAGAUAUUCCUUAAUGAAAUAUGACCUCCCCACUGCCCCAUCUUUAGGGAAUGGCAUUCACCAAAUCCUUUCAAAUUCAGAGAAAUUAGAAAACCUUGGAUCAUUUUAGUAUUAAAUUUAGUCUUAAAAUUGUGGGUGGUUGUCAAAUCAGACCUCGUCUAAGGGGACCUCAUUAGGCAGUUCUCUAUAAUGGUGACAGGGUGGCUUAAAAUGUCUUAACUAAAUGCAAAUUAUCUCAGAGCCAAAAGUUGAGCACUUGAAAGCCAAUGAAAUAUCUAUUUAAGGAGCACAGAAGGAUGUCAGAGAAGGAUCCAAAGUCCUGAUUUUUUUGUUACAUUAUAUUGGGGUAGAUUUACUGCAAGCCAGAGGAUUCUUUACGUAAUUAACUCCCAUUUGAAAAAAUAGCAAACAAUAAAACUAUUUUUUUUCCCUUUACCUUUGGUAUAAAUAGAACUAAGCCAUAGGUUGGUAUGUUUAGUAAGUAAUAGGUAUUAAGUAAGUAAUAUGUAUUACUUACAUUUUACCAUAGUUGAAGUGUGAACUUGAAAUAUUUUUAAAGCACAGUCUACAGUGGUAAGAACUUUUCUUUGCUGCAGUUUUAGAUUACCUAGGAAGAAGACAGUGACAUCCUGGAAUGAUUGUAAAUUGGUGCUUGAAACCCUGGAAGUGAACUGUUUUCCAGUGGCAGGAUGAUGUGAGGUUCAAUACUUCUCCCCUUUGAGUCUUAGAUUUUAAAUAGUCUAAUUCCAAAAUAUUUCCUUAGGCUGGACACGGUGGCUCAUGCCUGUAAUUCUAGCACUUUGUGAGGCCAUUGUGGGCGGAUCACUUGAUCCCAGGAGUUCGAGACCAGCCUGGGCAACAUAGGGAGACCCUGUCUCUAUAAAAAAAACCAACAAAAAUUAGCCAGGCGUGGUGACAUGUGCCUAUGGUCCCAGCUAUUCGGGAGGCUGAGGUGGGGCCAUCACCUGAGCCUGGGAGUUUGAGGCUGCAGUAAGCAAUGAUCACGCCACUGCACUCCAAUGUGGGUGACAGAGUGAGACCCUGUCUCAGAAACAAAACAAAACAAAAAAGCCCCCAAAACAAAAUGCUUCCCUUUAUUCUUGAGGCAUAGUUGAUGUUUUAAUGGUGUUAUAAACAUAAUUAUUAUCUUAUAUAGGCUGUGAAGUGAUUGCUUAUUGGUUUGGUACUAGAAACCAUAUACCUUUAAUUAUGUUUGAUCAUGUGAGACCCAGAAAUGCCUCCUGUACACGCCUUUACCAUUUCUUGGGAAGACAAUAGGGGCCUGCCAUCACUGUGAAGCAAUAAAGUGUAAAGGAUUGGAAAAUAGGGAUUGGGAUUAUUGAAACUGGAAAAAGUGAGGGAGUAAUUUAAAUUCUGUUUUAGUUAUUAAAAGUCUGGUUUCCUGACUGUGCUAAGUAUUGCAGAAAGACAAAGUGUGAGACAAAAUAUUUAGAUCUUCAGGAGCUUACAUUCAAGACAAGGUUAACCUGAUGCUGUAGUUCUGGUUGUGUUCCUCCAAGAGGCAGGAGAGGAGAAUUGGAGAUAUUCAGAACAUGUUUGGGAGGAAUGUAGUAAUCAGGGCACCCUUCUGGUUUAAGUUGUCUUUUCUGCUUCGCUGCUAUUCAGAAAGUGAAAAGCUUUGUUCUGGAACUUUGAGAUAUAGAUGGGUCUUUUGCUUUUAAUAAUUUAAGGUAACUCCUUCAAAGAUAUUGCAGGUCUAGUUCACAAAACAAAUUGUACAGUGAGCUGAGAGCAACUUUCUCUGUCCUGAGUUUUGAUGAAGUUGUUUUUUUUAAAUCAUGAUCAGGAUACAGGUCCUCAAUUAGUUUGUCUGGAAUUUAGUAAGCGGAGUGCUGGAGAUUGGAGAUCAGAGUAGCAUGAAGAUUGAAUAAGAUGGGGAUUGCACAUUCUGGUUUACCCAGUUUGGAAGAGUAAUGCAUAGGUAAUAUACAGGUUGUGUUGAUGGGUGAGGAUACAGAUGUCACAGUUUGUGAGAAUUCAAGUGUAGUGAUUUAUUUCAUUUAAUCUACUGGCAGAGCUCUAAUUUACUUAUGGAGCUGUAGAAACAAAAAAUUUCUAAUAGGGCUGAGUGCGGUGGCUCACGUCUGUAAUCUCAGCACUUUGGGAGGUCAAGGCGGGUGGAUCACUUGAGGCCCGGAACUCGAGACCAGCCUGACCAACAUCAUGAGACCCUGUCUCUACUAAGAAUGCAAAAAUUAGCCUGGCGUGGUGGCACACAGCUGUAAAAAUAUCUCAGCUACUCAGGAGGCUGAGGUAUGAGAAUUGCUUGGACCUGGGAGGUGGAGGUUGCAGUGAGCCAAGAUCGAGCCACCUCACUCUAGCCUGGGCGAUAGAGUGAGACUCUGUCUCAAAAAAUAUAUAUAUUUUUAGUAGUUUUUGCUAUAGUUUUAUGAAAGUAACAAGACUAGUAAAAUUAUAAAACAAUUGGCCUUUAUGGUCUAAAGCGUUCUUAUUUAUAGCCACCCAGAAUGUAUCAUCUGCUAGUCUCCACUCUGCUGUCUGUCCUUUCCAUCAUCCCUCUUGGGCGCCCUACCUGGCUGGCCUGCCCAGUAAGUAUGGCACCAGGUUUCCUGUUCUGGGCCUCUGGCUGCUUUGUACUUCUCCAUUCCUGGAGGUCUCUGGACCUUCAGCUGCUCAAAAUUCAAUUGCACCAACUUUGACUGAAGUGCACUGCUGAUGAUCCUUCUCUUUGUGAGCCUUGCCUCUUCCCUAUGAGCUACUUUCUGCCUAGACCUCCUCAUGGUGCCGUGUCCAGAACGUGGGAGCCACCCGGCUAGGAAACUCAACACUGCUGCCCUCCUAGCAGUAGCAGCAAGCUACAGCUUGCCCCCUUUCAAGGUGUUUGACCCUGUUGGAUUUCUCAUUGCUCCCCUUCUUGCUUUGUAUUUUUUUUGGCAGGAAGAGUCUCUUUUAUUUCUGAGCUGAUUUGCAGAUCAGAAACGAUGGACCUCUGUUGAACUCUGAAGCAGUCCUCCCUCUCCACUUGGGACUGCUAGUCCUCUUGCCUUUGGUAUAAAGGGGUCCUCCAUCUGUCCCCAGGCCCCAUCCUCCGAGAGGCCUUCCAGAACCUGAGCAUUGUGUUUUUCUUUUUCAAUACUUUAGUACCUUAGAAACCAGAAAGUGAUAAAUGAGGAGAGUAGGUAUGAAGUAGAAGAGGAUUUUGAUGGCCAGCUCGUAAAGUGUAGCGUUAAGUGAAACAUUGUGAUGUGAACAAUUUGGUAUUUUUGAAAGUCCUAAUGCUACUUGUACCAGGUGAAAUGUUUAAAUCUCUCUCAAGCCCCUAGCAUUUUGAUAUUCUUAAAAAAGAAAAAAAAAGCCACACAGAAGGCAUUAGUCCAGCGUGGUAUGUUAUUGAAACUGGAACGAUAUUGCAGCAUAUCUCCACAUCUCCCGUUGACGGCAAAGCUGAGCCAGUGAAACAGGUGUGAGCCUUUGAGACUGCUGGGAUAACCCAUGCUGUGGAGAUGGAAAACUAAACUUUUGAGUGAGUUUUCUGGUUUAUUGGGAUUCAUCCUUGGUAUAUCAGCAGUUGUGGUUUCAAGGUUCCAUAUUUUAGUUCUUGUUCCACUUGAUGGAACACUUGACAUCUAUCCUCUUCUGUAACUCCGCAAGAGGGGCAUUUGGUUAAUGGUCAUUUUGGAAAGAAAGCUAUUUUGGGGACAGUAAUUGCCUGGAGUCUUUAUGUAAGAAGAGACCGAAGAGUCUUAGCAAGGAGAAGGUUUCUGUUUGCGGCAUUUGGCCCAUAGUAUAGUACACAUUCCUGUUGUGUUGUUUUGUUUGCAUCAUUGGGCUUAGAUGUUAUUAGAUAUUACUAGUCUAAUCCAAUUCCUUGUUCUUGGAGAAUAGGUUUCUUGUUUAUCUGAAUGGCUUUUCUUUGCGUCACUAUGCCAGAAUAGUCAUUCUUGGACAGAAAUGAUGGUUUUAAAAUCUCUCUUACAUUUUAAGACCUGCUCUAGGGGUUGUAAAAUAGUACUGCUGUUAUUGGGAGGAGUUGGGUAGGGGCCACAGCAGCAGGGAGAGAGAGGCUCCCAUCGUACAAACUUGCAGACUUUUAUUAAAACGUAUUUAUUGAUUGCAAAUUAUGUCAACAGAGUGAGGCUUUGGUAACUCUUCAAGUUACUAGUGUUUCCUUCUUUGCAUAGUUGUUUCCCAUCACCCUUUAAACAUCUGCUGCUUCUGGUCUUGUCCAGUCAUGCUUGAGUGAUCAGCCCCAGAAGUCUGACAGCUCUUCCUGUCUUGACUCAGGACAGUCCAGGACAGCUGAGCUCCCUGCACUGAAACAAUGGGACUCCUGAAAACUGCUCUGCUGUUGACAUGAGAAGCACAUUUCCUCUUUCUUAACUUCCAGAAAGUUACUGUGGUGGCUUUGAAAUUUGUUCUGAAACAAUAAGCUCAAAGGAUUCUGUUAAUCUAUUCUGAUUAAUUUAGGAGGCAGCAGCAUUCAUUAUUUGACUUAUGUUAGUGGUUAAUUAACCAAAGUAGAACAUGUUCACUUUUUAUAAAUUAAAUGCUGAUAGAGUAACAAAGACGAAAUAUUUUACAACACAGAUCCUUGAAUUUGACUCUGAAAUAUUCUGUUAUUUUGCAGCAGUUUCCGGUUUUAGUGACACUUACAUACUGUUUCUAUUAUUAGCAAGUUUUGAAUUUAAGUAACUUGAAAUGGAUAUGAAAGUUGUUUCUAUAAAUAAUACAGACUGUACUCAUGUGAGAGUUUUUUUUCUUUAAUUUCAUUGUUGGCCUUGAUUGGGGAGAAGAUUUAUAUUUUAUGCCAGUCUUUUCUUGUUUAGAAUUGGCAAGAAUUGGAUUGAGUUGUAUUAAACUGUUUAUGUGAAUAGAUAGUUACUUUUGAGAUGUCUUUGAAUGUAGAAUAUUCUUGCAGCCAUUUCUUGAUGGUCUGCCUUGACUGUCUUAUGGACAGUUGGCAUCAGUGACACUUUCAUUUAUUUACUUAUUUAUUUUUUUUUAGACAGAGUCUCGCUCUGUCGCCCAGGCUGGAAUGCAGUCGUUCGAUCUCAGGCUCACUGCAACCUCUGCCUGCUGGAUUCAAGUGAUUCUUGUGCCUCAGCCUCCAAAGUAGCCGGGAUUACAGGCAUGCACCACUAUGCCUGGCUAAUUUUUGCAUUUUUAAUAGAGAUGGGGUUUUACCAUGUUGGCCAGGCUGGUCUUGAACUCCUGACUUCCAGCAAUCUGCCCACCUCGGCCUCCCAAAGUGCUGGGAUUACAGGAGUGAGUCAUCACUCCUGGUCAAUCAGUGACACUUUUAAAUCACUUGUGUCCUUGACUCUUUUUAUGUUGUCUUUAUGAGGGACAGGCCCUUUAUUCUACCAAGGAGACCUCCAUAGUUGCUCAUUCUGAAUUCUUUCAGGAAGAUUUGGUUGAGGGUUGUUCAUUAGGCUGGGGCCUCUGCCGGGGUGGGUUGAGAUUAGAUGGAUAACAGGAAAAUAAUCAUAGUGCUUCCCAGCCCCUGUAAGUGAGGGGUCUUCUUAGGAUAACUUUUUGGCUUGGAGUAAAUGUCCCCCCCAAAAUCUUAAACUCAGUUUAAGGGUGAAAACUUAAAUAUAAUUUGUUCCUGGACUUUGGGAUUCUGUGAACAUUUGUUUGCUUCUGUUAGUGAUGGUUAUGGAGGGUUUAACCGCCCACAUUUUCACUACCUUUUUAGCCCAAUAAAUGGAAAAAGAAAAGGUAGGCAGGGAAUUUUGUUCCACUUAAAACAUCAGUUGGCCUGUUCGGAUUCAGGUGACUCAAGGUUUGGUAAUGAAGCUAGAGAAGUCUUGUGCAGAUACACUCAAACUUCCUGACUGUGCAGUUCAGGGAAUUGUAAGUAGAGCCUGAGCAAGGAACACCUUGAUUGUUGGAGAGGAAAGGUGGAAGAUGAGCACUCCCUAAUCCUCCUCUACUCAGUUUCUUUAGGGUUAAAUGGGCAUUUAUUUAAAUGUAGGAUUCUGCUUGCCUGAACUCCCAAGGUUCUGUUAAUUGAAUUGAAUCCUUUCUAUCCUGGGCUUCCUCCCGCACCAUAGCAGAUGUGAGGAUAUGGAGCAUAAUGCAGUAGUGCUCUGUACUCUGUGUUAUGCAAUUUGAAAAGUGCCGUUCUAGCCCGAAAAUGUUAGUGCAUUGACUCUCUUUCACAUGAAAGGCCUUAAAGUUUACCCCUGGAAGUCAACCUAGGGUGGCACAGAGGCAGAGACCCAUUACCACCAUCAACCCUCUGGCCCUUUUAAAAGGUGGGGAGAGGCUACUGUGAACACUGAAGACAGCACUUUAGUUGGAUGGACUUCAUAAUUAAUGUCUCAUUAAGUGAAGACUUCCGUUUCAUUUGGCUUUCCAGACCAUUCGGUAGAAAUGCAGAGGAAUGGAGGGAGAACAGUGCAUCUCAGUUGGCAGGCAGGAAGAGCAGAUGUGGAAGAAGCAACAAAGAUUUUCUCCAAGCACUUGAGCCGUGCUUUAGGUAUAGAUGGACUGUCUUUGGGGCCAUCCUAGUAAUCAACAUGGUUAAUGGCAGCUUCUCUCUCUGUCCUUGAGUCUUUUAGCAAAAAUAAGUUUUUAUUUGACUCCUCAAGCAAGGGUACCCAGCCUUGGAGAGGAGAUGAAAUUAAGAUAAAUCUUUAUUUUUUCUUAUUUGUAUUUGAAGGGGAAGUUUAAAACUAGUCAUGUAAAUAGCUGUUUGGCUUAUCUGGACUUUCCAGUCAUUUUUGUUUUCCUUCCUUUCACGGAUAAUCAAUCUUUCACUAUCUGUUCGUAUUUGCUUCUUAUUGUGGUCUCCUGCUCCGCCCUGCCCACUCCCACUUUUUUUUUUUUUUUUUUUACUUUGUUCUGAGCCCUUCUCAGGCAGAGGAGGUCAGGCAGGUACACGUGCCUUUGGGAAGAAGGUGGUGGAAAAAUAUGGAAUAAUGAGCCCUUCUGACUUUGGAUUCAGCAAUUUAACAUUGGUGCAGUAGGUGGAGUUAUUCUUGGAGUCCCAGUUUGAAGAUUGCUGUGCAGAAACCCAUCUGUGCUGCUGGUUGCCAACAUUUCUGGUACAAAUAUUGUCAUUUGCUCUUGAGGCAAUCUGCUAUUUCAGUCCUAGAUGCAGUUUUGUAAUAUGCUGGGUAAAAUAGCAGACAAAAAAUAUCUUAAGUGGUGGUAUAAUCUUCAGUUUAAAAACACUUUAGCAAUGUUUCCAGUAGAGGAUUGUUCAACGUGUCUCCUUUCCUUGGCUGUAAACAUAAUCUAAAUUCAUUUUUCCUCGUUUGCCUGAGCCACGGUUCCCUUGUGCUGACUUUGCAUGUCAGUAACUUCCGUACCCAUCAGAGAGGAAAGACAGAGGGGCAGUCUUGUGCAGGUAAAAGGUUUAAGUAGUAACAUUUCCUUAAGAUUGCACCCUGUAGAGGUUUAGCAUUCCAUGAUCAUUCUGUUGAUAAGCAAAUGAGAAAUGAGUAACUUGCUCAAAAGUUACUUGGUUACAAAAAUUGUCAAAACUGAUACUACACACUAUUUCCCAUUUGGUACCUUUUAUCCCUACACACUAUUUCCCAUUUGGUGCCUUUUAUUCCAGACUGCAAGAGUCAUAUCUUCUGUGCAGGCUGCUGAACAGCUUCACAAGGGGGUGCCUCUGUUGCCUGUGAGGAGUAGGUGUUCUUGAUGGGAUUGGGGUCUCCCUGGAAACCCGGGGAUGGGACUGUGCCACCAUUUUAUUGGGCUUUUGUUAUUAAGCCCUUCUUAGAGAGAGAAAGCAUAUCCUGUAGGAAGUAGUAUGUUUCCUUCUGUUUCUGUGGCUUUCUCAGUUUCUUCCCAUCUUGAUGCAUAGUGAGAAAUCCAUUUUACAGUAUGACUCAGUGCACAUAUGCACACAAUGAUAGAAGAGUUUUACAAAAUAGUACUGUGCUUAGCCAUUUAUGUAAGACUGUUUUGUUAUUAUUUACAGAAAUGCUAGCCACAAUCCUCUCAAUUGGUUUCACUAUUUUAUGGAUUGUGAUCCAGAGUUUUAGCCUGAGGGCUUUCCCACAUUCUUUCAAGACCUUUGUGUCAUGGCAGCAGCCUUGAAGUUAGGGGAAACAGGUAGAUGAAUCCAUAUAUGGAGAAUUGGCCAUAUAUGGGAAAUGAGGAGGGAGUUCACAGGUCAGUCACUUGAACACACAAUGAUUUGGGCUGAGCCAGUUUUUAAGUAGCCCCUCUCUGGAUUGGUCUCAAACAUGGAACUAGUUAAACUUACGUACUAAAUCAAACAGACCCAAAAGACACCGUUUGUUUUUUAAGUCUUGCUGGCACAGACUAGCUAGGAUAGGGUUUUUCAUCCAUCUGGACAUCUUGUCGUUUAGCUUUUGUAUACAACCCUUGAAAAUGGGCAGCUGCUGGGUCCACUUUCCUGGAUGAGGUUUCUUGCUUCUUUCUUUUGAGAUUAACCUGAGUAGGGCUCACCUGAAUCAAUUAUUUCCGCAGAAGCUUUCAUCUCAUGAAAGCGCAUUCCACUUUUCAUGUCUUCAGGGCAAAUACGAAUUGCACUUCCACCCUGAAGUCAGAACUGUAAAGGAAUUUUAGGUGUUAUCAAUGUUUGAUAAGAAGUGAUUACCCUUUCUCUGCAGAGCUGGAACAGCUGAAGCUGGUGUGAUCUGGCUGGGAGAAGGCUGUGCUCUGGAAUAGUGUCCUUUCCACUGAGUCCCUGACUUGCCUGUUGGCAUAUGGAGCAGUAAUCUUUUCAAAACUCCAUUGUGAAGUUGGCUGUGUGUGUGUGUGUGUGUGUGUGUGUGUGCGCGCGCGCAGAGGAAAUACUUACAUACUAAAGGGGAAAGCGGGGGAGGAAAAUUCCAGGAAAUUGCAAGGUGAGGUUGACAUUCCUUAUUCUCUUAACUCUUGCUUCUGUUUUUCUUUCUGAAAAACAAUGAUGACUUAAAAUUUGAUCCCAGAACCAACUGGCUUUUUAUCCGUAAGAUUACAGUUGUGUUUUUUAGACAUCCUUUCAUAAAUAUCUAAUGAAUUGCCUUUUAUUAUUUGGUGUUAAUGACCAAAAGUACCACUAACAUAGUGUUUCUCAUACUUGCCUGUCAUAUAAGAUACUUGUUAAGAAUAUUCUGGGACUUCAUCUUCCUCUUGUUAAAUCAGAAUCUACCUGGAAUAACAUAGUUACCUUAUUUUCUUAGAAUAGUAGAACUGAAAAGAAUCUUACACAUGAAAGUAGUUCAGGUGUUCCCAAACCUGGCUCCAGUACCAUGACUGCUUUAAUAGAUUGCCAAGCUGCGCUUCAUACCUAGUGAAUCAUAACAUCCGAAGCUUCCUAGAAGAGUCGGACCAUUAGACUGGAGGGAUAACUACUCGCUUAUUCGGUUGCCUUCAGGAAAGGGGAAUUUAUGUGCUUGGUUAUUGGGCUGAUUAAUAGCAGGACAAGAAAUCUUAUUGUCUCUGUAGAUUCAUCCAAAUAAUAUCCAAAUAUAUAUAUAAUGUUUGUUUGAGAUGGGGUCUCACUUUGCCCCCCUGGCUGGAGUGCAGUGGCACAAUCACAGCUCACUGCAGCCUCAACCUACCCGGGCUCAGGUGAUCCUCCUACCUCAGCCUCCUGAAUAGCUAGGACUAUAGACACGUGCCACUGCAUCUGGCUUUUUUUUUUUUUUUUUUUUUUUUUUUUUUUUGCAUUUUUUGUGGAGAUAGAAUUUCUCCAUGUUGCCCAGGCUGGUCUUGAACUCCUGGGCUCAAGCCAUAUGCCUACCUUGACCUCCCAAAGUGCUAGGAUUACAGGUGUGAGCCACCAUGCCCAGCCCCAAAUAAUAUUUACAUUUCAGGUACUGACUAGGUAGGUGAGUGGGGGCAGUUUUGAGAUGGGUGAGCAAGGUCUCUCUGCCUUGGAGGUAUAUGUGGAUUGUUAUUCAGCCUUUCUCAAGGGAUGAGUUUUAGAGAGUGGAAUUAGACUCACUUGAGGAGCUUUUUAUUAAAAAAAAUUCUAAUACCCAUAUAAGACUGCAAACUUAACUGAUAAAUGUUUGUUCUCACUGCUCCACCAACCUGCCAUUCCCCAUCUGUCUCCCCCUCUUCAGGGUUCCCUAUCCCUGAGACAAAACAAUAUUGAGAUUAGGCCAUUAAAACCCCCACAAUGGCUUCUACAUGUUCAAAUAAAAGGAAGAGUCACACCAUCUGAUCUCACUCACUGUAAAUCAAAGGCUAGAAAUGAUUCAGCUUAGUGAGGAAGGCAUGUAUAAAGCCCAGAUUGUCCAAAAGCUAGGCCUCUUAUGCCAGUCAGCCAAGUUGUGAAUGCAAAGGGAAAGUUCUUGAAGGAAAUUAAAAAUGCCAUUCCAGUGAACACAAAUUAUAAGAAAGCAAAACAGCCUUAUUGCUGAUCUGGAGAAAGUUUUAGUGGUUUGUAUAGAAGAUCAAAACAGUCACAACAUUCCUUUAAGCCAAAGCCAUGUUCAGAGCAAGGCCGUAACUCUUAAAUUCUGUGAAGGUUGAGGGAGGUGAGGAAGCUGCAGAAGAAAAGUUUGAAACUAGCAGAGGUUGUUGGUUCAUGAGGUGUAAGGAAAGAAGCCAUCUCCAUAACAUGAAAGUACAAAGUGAAGGAGCAGCAAGUUAUCCAGAAGAUGUAGAUAAGACCAUUGAUGAAGGUGGCCACACUAAACAACAGAUUUUCAAUGUAGAUGAAGUGGCAUUCUAUUGGAAGAAGAUGCCAUCUAGGACUUUCAUAGCUAGAGAGGAGAAGUUAAUGCCAAGCUUCAAAGAACAGGUUGUGAUUCUCUUAUUAGGGGGGUAAUGCAGCUGGUGGCUUGAAGUUGAAGCCAAUGCUCAUGGACCAUUCAGAAAAUUCUAGUGCCCUUAAGAAGUAUGCUAAAUCAACUCUAUCUGUGCUCUGUAAAUGGAACAACAAAGCCUGAGCGACAGCACAUCUGUUUACAGCAUGGCUUACUGAAUAUUUUAAGCCCACAGUUGAGACCUACUGCUCAGGAUGAAAGAUUCAAAAUAUUAAACUGCUCAAUGAUAAUGUACCUCCUCACACAAGAGCUUUGAUGGAGAUGUACAAGCAGAUUAGUGGUGUUUUCUUGUCUGCUAACACAACAUCUGUUCUGCAGCCCAUGGGUCAAGAAAUAAUUUUGACUUUCAAGUCUUAUUAUUUAAGAAAUAUAUUUUAUUAAGGCCCAAGUUGCCAUAGUGAUUCCUCUGAUGGAUCUGGGCAAAGUAAAAUUAAAAAUCUUCAAGAAAGGAUUUAGCAUUGUAGAUGCCAUUAAGAAAUUUGUGGUUCAUGGGAGGAGGUCAUAAUAGCAAUAUUAAUAGAAAUUUGGAAGAAGCUGAUUCCAGUCUUCAUGGAUGACCUGGGAGGGGUUCAAGAUUUCAGAAGAGGAAGUAGAUGCAGAUGUGGUGAAAACAUCAAAAGAACUAGAAUUAGAAGUGGAGCCUGAAGAUGUGAUUGAAUUGCAGCAAUCUCAUGAUAAAACUUGAACUCAUGAGGACUUGCUUCUUACGGAUGAGCAAAGAGAGUGGUUUCUUGAGAUGGAAUCUACUUCUGGUGAAGAUGCUGUGAAUGAACAUGGUUGAAAUGACAGUAAAGGCUUUAGAAUAUUACAUAAAGCGGUGGCAGGGUUUGAGAGGAUUGACUCUAAUUUUGAAAGAAGUUCUGCUGUGAGUAAAAUGCUAUCAAACAGCAUCACAUGCUACAGAGAAAUUUUUCGUGAAAGAAAGAGUCAAUCAAUCAGGCAAAUUUAAUUGUGUUGUUUUAAGAAAUUACCAAAGCGAUCCCAGCUUUUAGCUACCACCACCCUGAUCAGACUGCAGUAAUUAACAUUGAGGCAAAGGCCCUCCAGCAACCGAUCACAACUCGUUGAAGGCUCAGAUGAUUAUUAGCAUAUUUUAACAAUAAAAGUUUUUAAUUAAGAUGUGUACAUUAUUUUUUUAAAAUAUGGCUAUUGCACACUUAAUAGGCUACAAUAUAAUGCAUACCUUUUAUGCACAGGGAAACAAAAAUUUGUUUUUACUUUAUUGUGAUAUUUGCUUUAUUGUGGUAUUCUGGAAGUGAACUUGAGGUAUCUCUAAGGUAGGCCUGUAUUUCAUACAUGAAGAAAGGCAUAGAGACCAAUAUAAUUAGUACCCAUAUUCUACCUCUCUGUUUUAGCUAUAAAUAUAAUUCUUCCCCUCCUUGUCCCAGAGGUAGCCACUAAUUCCAGAGUUUGUGUGUUGAAGGGCACCUUUCCUGCCAGAAGCCCGUACCCUGGCUGUGCUGAUAGAUGGGGUCCACAAAUUCUUUGUAGGAUCCCCUUUUUAAAAAAAGCUUUACAUAAAUGUUAUCAUUUAAGGUAAACACCAUUCUGUAACUUGAUUUUCUUUAAUAAAAGUCAGCAUGAUAUUUUUGAGAUGUAUUGUUCUUACAUGACCAGAUAUGGCCCCAUACUUAAUAGUUAAAUCAGGAAAUUGAAGCCAGACAGCUUGAAAACCUUCUUAAUGGAAAAAAAUGCAAGAAGUGGGUGGGAUAGAGUUUCUGUUGAAUUUUUGUAUAGAACAUUGUCAUUUGUGGGAAACUAGUUGAUUUGAAUUCUGUGUUAUUUUGAAUAGCCUAAUAACAGCUUAAUGAGGAUUAAUUGCAUGUUGUAUGGAAAGUUAAUUGUUUUAAUUUACUAUGGGUGUAGUUACUGCAGUUUGGUUCAAACAGGUGAAAGUUAAGAUUUGUAGCAUAAAACAGGAAGCAGAUGGGGGCUAAUUAAAGUUCUGUUGAUGAUAAAAGGAUGACUGAUCAAGGAGCGAGCAGCUGGUUUCUCAAUUUAAACACAAUUUGUACUAUUGUAUGAAGACAGCCCUCUGCAAGUUCUCAUGAGUAUCUUUCAAAGGUGAAGGCAUGUGUUCCAGCAACAAGUGUGAAGGCUGUUGUGGCCCUGUUUGUGCUCGCUCCCCUUUUUUGCCUUCAAGCAGUGUCACUUCAGGUUUUUCCAAAAAAGGGGGUUAAGGGAUCACAAAACCUGGCCAGAUUUUCAGUGAUGCUCUCUGGACACCUGUUGUGUCCCAGAAAAGUCUAAAGCUCUUUCUGUCUCCAAGAAAAGUGCCCAAGCAUUUCAUUUCCUUUUGUAGUUUUUCUUACUUAUCUCAACUCCGUCUCUUGGCAGGCUUUCCAAUGUUGUUGCCCUGACCAUAACCCAAGAAGGCCCACAUCUAGCUAGCGGAAGCGCCGGGUAUUUAAGUGUGUAGGCGAAGGCUAAGCAGUGCUGUAGAUACUUUCCUGGAGCCUCACCUUGUUCUUCAGGGUCUUUGAGCUUCUGGCCAUGAGAUGUUAGGGACUUGAACUUAUUUUGCUUGAUUGUGUCCUGGAUGACUUUCACCUUCAAAUGACAGCAUCUUUUGUUGCUACUGCUAAUAGUGAUUGCGUAAACAUUGAGGACAAGUGUCCUCUAUGUGUUUUGCUUAAGGAACAUGCCAGCACUGGGUUUUCUUUGAAUGUGUGCAGGGAGGUGACAUGAGGUCAGAUGAGGUGUGCCUUGCUUGGAGCCAGGGGCUAGACAUUUGCUUGAGAUUUUGUGCCCAUAAUAUCUAAUAUUUAUAAGUGCUUUGUAGGAUUAUCUCAUUUUAGUCCUUACAAAAAUGCUUUGGAAUGGAAGUUGUUUAUCCCCAUUUUGUAGAUGAGGAGAUUGAAGCCUGGAGAGGUAAAGUGACUCAGCCAAGGUCUCACAUUUGCUAAGUGCCAGUACUGGAUGUAGAUUCCAGGUUUGUGUGACAGCAAGCCCACGCUCCUCAGCCACUAGUUUUGUGUAAAAUUGUUGUUCUCUUUCCCCGUCUCCUGCUUAAGGAAAGAUAUAUUGUUUCCUGGAAAAACAAAAAUGUUAGCAUAUAGUUUGCAAACUACAACUUAUUAUUUGGUUAUGCAGGUGUGUGUGUGUUGUAUAAACAUUAUAUAUAUUUCACUUGGAUAUAUUCCACUUGAUAGGAACUGCUUUGUUUUUGAAUGAAUAUAUGAGAAAGGAAAAUGCCUGGGUUUUUGUUUGUUACCCCAAUGUAGCAACAUUAUGAAAGGUAAAAUGCUCUUUCUUUAACAGCAGCAGCAAAAAAGACAACAUGCAAAGGUAAUCUACAAAGUAAAAAGCCCCAUUAUAUUCACCACCUGGAAGCAACAUUAUUGUAUUCAUCAAAAUUGUCUUGUAAAAGAAGUAAUUGACCAUACAGAGCUCGUAUAAUUGGUAAUAAAGAGCACCCUGUAUUUUAGUUGCAAAUAGUGUGCAAUAGGUUUCAGGGGUGUCAUGAUUGAUGUUCACUGUCAGGUGUUGUAAAUAAACUUUCCAAUCCCAGAUGGUGUUUUUGCCUAGUUAGGUUCUACACUGAUCCCACCACAUAUUACACUAAUGGGGAAACCUUGUGUACAGGUUCCUCAUCUUCCAAGCUCUAUUGUGGUGACCCUAGAAACUGCCUAUGUGCUCACAUCAUGGCUCCUAACAGCAUGAGGAGGAGUGUCACAGCCAAGGCUAGAGUGUUUUCCUGGCCUGGGAGAAGUCUUAGGAUUGUACCGCCCCCGCCCCCUUUUUUUUUCAUUCUGCUGCCUUCUCAGCAGUCAACUUCAGAAUCACUCUUCUCCUGUCUUCUUUCCCCCUUCUUUGCUUGUUCCUUCCUAUACCUUGCUUGUCUUUUUACAGAAGCAUUUAAGGAGAUGGAAAAGAUUUGGCCCAUUCUUCUCCUGUCAUAACUCUGCCUGUGUAUUUCUGAAGAUGAUGUUGACUGUUGGGGAAUGGGAUGUAGGAGAAAGAGGUCUACUGUGGGUCUUGCUUCGCACGGAGUAAUCCGACCUGGCGUGGAUUGUCUGGUCUCCUCCUUCAUCCAUCAAAGAGUAAGGCAUGGUUCAAUUACUUCUAGCAGCAAGUCCCACAGAACACCUGGGCUUUCUGAGCUACCUAGGGCAGGUGUGUUAUUUGGUAGGAAGUUUGGGCAGCACUGGGGCUUUCAGUGAGAGCCCCUCCUUCUACCUUGGCAUAAUCAUAAAAUCUCACCAAUACGUAGCCCUUUAUGCUUUUUGAAGCACUUAUACCCAUUACAAUUCUGUGGGGCAUUUAGGACAGACAUUGUUUUCCUACUUUAUAGACAAGAAAGCUUAGACAUAAAGGAUGUAAAAAUGUGUCCAGUCAGAAAGAUAGAGCCAGACUUAGAUUUUCUUCCUCAUUACCACCGUCUUGCCAUUAGAUCAGCAUUUUCCAAAAUGUGUGCUGCUGAACAUCAGUUUCAUGGUAUAGUCUGUCAAGAAGCGCGGGCAAAGAAAUGUGUAUGUGCGUGGAGGGGUGUGCAUGUGCAUGCAUGUGAUCCCACCAACAAAACAAAACAAAGUCUAAGGGAACAGUUUUGCUCUUGUUUGUUUUGUGUUGUUUUGUGUACUCAAGGCUCUAAAAAACUGUACAGUUAGGAAUCCUGUUUAAUUCUGUGUGGCCAGAGUGUCCCAAAGGUAUUUUUUCAGUGAAUUCAAAUCACCCUAAAAGGAACCAUUAUUUUGUAGAGCACAUGCCGAAGAAUGCUUUAGUAGGCCAUAGUGUGCUGCUUUGUCCUGAAGCUACUUUGGAGGUGCUACAGGAGACCUCAAUGGUUAGAGGAAAAUCUGAUCUUCAGGGAACUUGCAGGGAAGAGUCCAGAGGAUGCUGAUACACAGUCAGUGGCUGGGGAUGCUUUGGGAAUAAAGACUGUCCCGAAGGUGGAGUGGGAUGGGAGGCUGGCUGCAGGGAAUCUUUGUCAUAAUGUCACUAUAAGCACCAUGCCUCCAGGAUUUCAUACCGAGUAGGAAUUUAACCAGAAUGCACAAAAGUUCUCAAUCUACAGGAUCAGCAUUCUAGGACCAGUUGUCAGCUUUGUUAGGUAAAGCUCCAUGAACUGUAGCCUGAGUGACAGCUGCAGAGUUUAUUGGCUUAGGGAUGGACUUAAGAAAUUUGGACCCAGUACAGCCAGCAUGCUGCUGCAUCUUGGCCUGAAGUUUGACAAGGCACAUUCCCUGAGUGAGGCCAUCUGCAUCAACCCCCGCUCCACUGCCCUUUCUUUAGUACUUAAUGUUCAACUUUGCGUGCAAUUUUGCUUUUACUAGAUGGCAAUUGAGGGAAGGGUGGAAGAGAAGUUGGUGGUAAAGGUGCCAGUCAGUGGGCACAUUCUGCAUCCAUGUUCUUAAUCAGCUCUUCUGUCUUUUAGCAGAAAUAGAACUUGAUAAAACUCUUUUAUUUUGAAGUAAGUUUGUUCCAGCCAAGCAGAAAGGAUAAAUUAUUUUGCAUUGAUAUCUGAAACUAAGGAAGCAAGUCUAACCUCCUAAGAACUGGUCAUGGAUAUCACCCUUGAUCUAUCUUUUCUCCUCUUCUGUUCAUUCUGUUUCAUUCUGUUAUGUUCUGCUUGGCUCUGUUCUGUUCUAGGCAUUGAGUAUAGAUCAAAAAGUUCAUGUAUAAUAUUUUUAAAUCCCGACGACAAAAACUUUAGAUUAAUGGAGGUGAUUAGUUUACUUAGUUUGGGCUGGUGAGGAGAAUAAAAUGAUCCUAGUAGGAGGAGUGGCUGGAAGAAGUGCUAUGAAAUAGGAAAAGUUAAUAACCUAAGGUGUGGUGUUCCUGUCUGCAGGUAUCUGUUAGCUAUCCUCCAUAAAGUGGUUUUAUGUUCUUCUAAAGUGGACAGAGUAUUAGACUCUGUGACCCAUUCUACAAAAUAUUUGAACUGUCUGCUAAGGUUUCUUUGUUUGCUAGUAACUGUGAGUUUUAGACCCUGUCUUAAGUUGCAUGGCACACACUUGGUUUGUAACAGGAAGGAAAGGAAGCAGUUAGAGGUCAGGGCAUCUGGCUGGUGGAAGAAGAAAGGAGGAUGGGAUCUGUUGAGGGUAAGGUUAACAUCACAUAAAAUGUUUAUAAUCGAAUUCUGUUGUGGGGAGUGCUCAUCAACCUUUUAAAAGUUUUCAAGAAUUGGACCACUUGUCUUCUAGUAUGCAUGUGGGCGGGGGGUAAUCAUGCCUUUCACAUUGAGGAGGAGGGGUGGGUGGGUGGGGGGAGUCUGAUGCCACUGCAGCUUAUCCUCAUGCCCCUGCAGUACCCCACAGCCUUGGCCCUGAAUCUCCUGUGCAUCCACCAGGGUACUGACUAAUGCAUGAGUAUUUUGUUGCAGCUUUAUCCAUGUUUGUGUGGAACAAUCCAUGGUUACAUUGUAGGCCAUUAUUUCCUUUAAUUUCCUUUUAGCUGUUCAAAACAACCUGAAAGAUGUUAUAGUUGAGCCUAGACAAUGACAUCAAGGAACAAAAAUAAACCUUCAAAAUGUAAGAACCAAAUUUUUAUGCCAAAUCUUGUGAAUGAUGGAUAAAAUGUAUGAAAGCAGUCAGCUUCAUGGAGGGAGACUUUUAAAAUCUGUUUUCAAAACAAAUGGUCCUGGCCCCAGCAUCCUGCCCUCCUUUGGCUAUGAAAAUAUCAGAUUAUGCCGUAAGUUUGAAAACAAUCAAGUAUCCUUCAAGUCAUGAGACAGAAGCCAAAGCUUGAAUCGAAAACCCUGUCAUUUUCAGCGAGGGAGACAGGGAGGAGGGCCUGAAGGUAACUUGUUUCUGGAGGCCCUUCUCUCAGCACUAGCUGCAGCAGCUUCCUGUUAGGUGGGAGAAGCACCACAGCCAAGGACAGCAGCUCCUGGAGAUGCUUUUACUUAUCAAGAGCAAUGUAGAUGUAUGCAAAAAUACAGACACCCACUCACAGUUACAUUUGUGGAUAAUCAGAAAUAUCUUUCUGCUUUCCCAGCAGAGCCCAAACUCUCCUCCUAUCAUCCAGGUGGGAAGACAGGUUUGGCGCUUUGCUCUAGGUUCUGCAUUAUAACUUUACUCUGUUGUCCUCUGAUCUUCCACUGGCUGUCCUGUGAGUUGCAUGUAGGGUAAAAAACAUGCUGCUGUGUUAAGGCCCCACCCACCGUACCUCCUCUCUCUCUCUCCUCCCUUUCUGUGUCUAAACUCAUACAUGGCCAUACUGACCUCUUCUCUUUUCUCCAGACAUACCUUACUAGUGUUUUUAAAAAAGUUUCCUCACAAACACUAAUAGCUCAUAUUUAUCGGACAUUCUGCACAGUGGUCAGUAAGUACUGUUAGUAUUUCCUUCUUGCAGACAAGGGAACCAAGCCCAAAGAUCGCAAGCCAUUUAUCCAAGAGCACUCAGGCCGUAACUGGGUUUGAACUGGGCCAGUCUGGUUCUAGCACACAUGUUCUGCACCACCACAUAGUUUGUCUGUCAACAUUGGUUCAUGCUCUGCCCUACCUCAAGAAUUCCCAUCCCGUUUUAUCUAGCAAUCCAAGUCGUCCUUUGCUUCACGUCCCAAUUCCAGCGUAGGGCCUUUCCUUUCUUGUUUUGCGUGUGCUGCACCUUAACGUUUCUGUGUUGUCAGCCUUCCGUACAUAUGUGUAAGACCAUGGGAGGCAGGGAGAGCCUUGAGCCUUAAUGCCUACUUGUUAUUUCCACAGUAUACAGUAGGGGCUUAGUAAAUAAUUGUUCAUUGAAAAUUACAUUGAUCGGUAUUGAUUUGACCAAAUCAAAAGAUCCUAAUUUAUGUUAUUGAAAUGUGAAUGGAAAUAAAUUAACUUCUGAAAUUGUCAGUUGAUUGAAAUACUUUACAUUAGGUAGGCCCACAGAUUUUCCAGUGACAAAAAUGAAGAUAAAAAUUGAUCUUUGGUUUGUAUUCCCAAUAAAAAUAACUGACACAGGGUCCUUUGAGACCCUUCCUCCUUGGUGCCCUUCACUCCACCUACCCCCACCCCUGGCAAGUGCUCUAACACUGACUUGGGCAGGAUGAACUGGACAUGUUCAGUUCCAGUCCUGAUUCUCUGAAUGGUCCCUUAUUUAUUUAUUUUUGUCACCCAGGCUAGAGUGCAUUGUUGUGAACUUGGCUCAUUCCAGGCUCAACUUCCUGGGCUCAAGCUAUCCUCCUGCCUCUGCCUUCUGUGUUGCUGGGACUACAAAUGUGCAACACCACACCUAACUUUUUGAUUUUUUUUUUUUUAAUGUAGAGACAGGAUGGUCUCAUUGUGUUGCCCAGGCUGGUCUUAAACUCCUGUGCUCAAGCAAUCCUCCCUCCUUUGCCUCCGAAAGUGCUGGGAUUACCGGUGUGAGCCAACAUGCCUGGCCCAAAUGGUCCUUUUAAAGUCUAUCAUAUAUUUCUGUCAGAGACUUCAUGAAGAUAGACCUCAAUAUAUUGGAUAACCAUUUUAGUCUUCAAAGUAGCUAUAAAUUAAGCUAGGAAUAGCAAGCAAUUUUCGAACAAAAUAUUUCUUUAAAAGAGUUUUCUAGGUUUGGCUAUUUAUUAUGUGUGAUAGAUUUUUUAAAUGAUUAAAAUGUGAAACUUUUCUUUUUGGGGGUGGUAGGGUACCACUGAAGAAUGAUUGUUUUACACUUUGUUCAGUCAACAGCAGUUCUAAGUCAUCCAUUGCAAUCUUAACUAGGCUGUCAGAAUUUAGCUAAAUUAGUUUUCUCAGUAAUCAAAAUGAAAAUAAAUUGAAAUACCAGAGACUACAUGUUGGUUCAGAGAAAAGUGAUCUUUGAGAGUUGAAAUGCUGAAGUAAUCUGUUAGACUGACCUUACUGCUCAUCUCUUUGUUAUAUAAGUAUCUGUGACAGUAGAGCCAAUAAUUUCUAAUAAAAACCUUGCAUUUUGUUCUAGAAUAUCAUGAGUUUAUAGAAUAAUUCUCGAAUAUGCUUGAAAUUGGUAGCAUUCUUCACAUGUAUAAUCUGUUUUAUGUUUUCCAAACAUGUUCUCAUUUAAUCUUCACAAUGCACCAUUCAGUUAUUUGGUACGGAGACACCAGGGCAUCAUACAGCUCAGAUUCACACGCGCAGUAAUGAUCUAACUUGGACACAGACAUACACGCCCUGACUUCUAGUACUCUUCCUACUGGACCAUAUUGGCAACUUCGUAGUUUUAAGAGAAGUAGAGAAAAGGCAUCUCCAAAUGUGCUAAUACAUACAUUGUGGUGGAAAACUAACAGCAGGUCAGAGUAUCCUUUUUAAAAAUUUUUUAUUUUACUUUAAGUCCUGGGAUACAUGUGCAGAGUAUCCUUGAAUAGUAGCUUGGAAGAGAUAAAAAAACGUUUGUACUUGUGUGCAAGAUUCUAGCCACAAUAGUUGAUAUUCAGUUCCCUUUUGGAGGAAAUUGAAAGUGAAAACGCUGAAACAAUGAGGACUAAAAUUCCAAAGAGGAGUUUAAGGUGUACCAUCGCAAAUUAUUGGCUUGUGUGGGAGAUUCUAAUUUUCUGUUGGUUUGAGUCAUCCUAAAAAAUGGUUCAUUUAAUCAUUCAUUCCUUCUGCCUUUGCUAGUUUGCCCGAAGUUAUUAAGAUUAUCUUUGUGUUUUCAUCCUCAAACACAAAUGUGUAUUGCGCAUAGCCAGUGUGUUUUAAAAGAUCAAGACUUUUCUUAAAAUGAUGUCGAUAACUUCCAAAGGCAACUGUGAGGUUUUUUUGUUUUGUUUGUUUGUUUGUCGUUUUCUUUUGUUUUGGUCUUUGGAGGUUUAUAAAGAUAGUCUUGUCUUAACGUAUGACAACAAUAUCAUCCAUGUUUCCAAAAAAGACAUGAUUCGAACUGCAGCAUUAGAAUAAAACAUUUAAUAUUUAAUACAAGGAACACUGUCCAUAUGGUAAGGUUUGCUUAGUCAUUCAAGUGGGGACCCUCAGGUGGUUCAGGGAUCCCUUUUUUCCUACCUGACAUUCUCCCUUCUCUCUGGAGCCCAAAGAAUUCCUAGUGGGAUGUCCUCAAGUCAUCUAAAUGUGGUUCCAGGGCAGACUCAACUUGGAGCCUUCCAGAAUUCCUUUAGCCCAGGAGUGAUCUUGGGGAAGCACAUUCUUCCUGGGCUGGCUUGCUUUGACCUGAGACUGCAUUUAAGCUGAAAGUCCUGGUGGGCACCUCUGACACAGAUGUGCCCACAUCUGGUGGAGUGCCAGUGACUGCGCAGUGGUGAAAGCUGCUCUGCAGGCUUCUUUUCUGCUCAGUGGGUGCUGAGUUUUCAAACAGACAUGAACAUGCAGCUCUCAGCACAGGUGCUUCCACUGGGGUGGAAAUUUGGCCUUACAAAUAAGCAAAAUGUAGGCUUCAUUCAUGUUAGGUGUGUGCUGAUGGGGAUGUGUGGCUUUAGUGUGGGCACAUUGAGGAGGGCCAGGAGGAGUCAUGGAGGCUUUUUAGGUAUGUUAAUGAAAGCAGCAUUACUGAAACAUUUAUGUGAGCUGCUUUUGGAGUCCCCAAACACGCCUGGGCUUCUGGUGAUGCUGAGGGAGCAGCAGUUUGUGAGGGGGACCAUGUCUUUUGUAUUACUUAGAAGGAAGGUGUGGACAGCAGGGCUGUUGCGCAGCAGACCUACUGUGUCUUAGAGUGUAAUUGUGCUCUGCCUCCUCAGGUGGAUCCCUGAUGUCUGUGGGAAGCUGGGCCACAGCCCUGACUUGGGCUCAAUCUCUGUGAUGGUGGGAGUUUCUCUUUAGCAUAAACCUGGGCCCAAAUAGUUUUGCUAUUAUUGGGUCAACCCAUUUGGGAAGCUAUUUGAUUUGAGACAACCUUUGAAUAAUAUUUGGGUGGUAUAUAAACAAACAUAUAUAUUCGGCAGUCUCGAGUCGUUGUUGCAUUAGGCUUCCUAGACAGAGUAAUGGGCAAGCUGGUGUCAAGAUUCUACGUAAACCCUACAGGAAAACCCAACAUUGCAGGUAGUGUAAUUCAGAGUGUUACACUUUAUUGCAGUUUGCUGUUGUUUUUGUAAUCUGGAUUAUCAUAUCUAGGUCCCAAAAUAGAAAAAACACAUAAAUCUAGACUUGGUACUCUGUUUACUAAGAAUUCUUAGUAAACAGACUAUGCGAAAAAACACAUAAAUCUAGACUUUGUACUCUGUUUACUAAGAAUUCUUAGUAAACAGACUAUGUAUCCAAUAGAUAAAUUCUUCCCUAGAUUUUCCAGAUAGCAAACAUAUUUAGGAUAAAAACAGUUCUACGUAGUACAUGCUAUGGGUGGGAUAUUGUCCUAGGGAUUUUAAUCUGUCAAAGUUUCAGUGUUCUUGCUUCUGAAUUUAUAUCCAUAAAGUUUUUCACUGGCUUCUGUAAACAAUUCGGGAACAUACCUUGAAUAUACAUUUACCUAGCAUGAACAGGAUUAACAGGCUCAUCAAUGUAAUGCUGACAAAAUACUUUAAAAUUCACUUUAGUCCUUUAAAAUUUUAGAAAGCUUUAAAAUGGAUCAAAGUAUUGGUAUGGCUAUGCUUUAUUUUAUGCCUAAUUUAAAUUCUUCAUCAGAAGAGAGUAGAUCCUAAUGCGUUCUUUGUUUUUGGUUUUAACUUUGUUGUGCCUUAGUCUUCUGGUAGCCAAAUAGAUAAGGUAGUUAAUUGCGUUAUAAUGCUGUGCGUUUAUAGGACCACUGCAGAUUAGAAAAAUUGUAUGGCCUAUAAAACAGACAAAGAUUUUCAUUAGGAACAGCAGAAUUACUUCAGCGUCAAAUGAGUUUCCUCUUAAUAUUCUCCUGUGGUGGGGCCUUUUGCAUCUGAGACAGCCAUUAGGCGGAAGCAGCAAAAAGCAUGGGUAUUCCAGUAGUUAAUUCAGUCGAAGUUUCAGGAAGGCCCCUUUAGGUCACUGAUGGGCAAGAUGGGGGAGUUGUGGCUGUCUGCUGUGGAUUUGGCAGUACCUGGCCUCUGUGCCUCCCUGGGGAGGAGCUGGUGAGUGGGUUAAAGGGUCCCCAGGGGUAACUGCAGGCUGCAUCAAAACUAAAUCAAUCCUAGGGGAAACAAGCUCCACUUUGAAAUCCUUGGUAGCCUACAGAUCUCUUUUUUUAUUUACUUUUUUUAUAGUACUUUAAGUUCUAGGGUACAUGUGCACAAUGUGCAGGCUUGUUACAUAGGUAUACAUGUGCCAUGUUAGUGUGCUGCACCCAUUUACUCGUCAUUUACAUUAGGUAUAUCUCCUAAUGCUAUCCCUCCCCCUUCCCCCCACCCCAUGACAGGCCCCGGUGUGUGAUGUUCCCCUUCCGCCUACAGAUCUCUUCAAACAAGGCAUUUAGAAGAAUUUUAGCUAGAUGAAAUUUAGUCUCUGGAUAUCCACCACAGGGACCUUAUUAGCUAGGGUUGAUGACAUUCAUUUGAGAGCUGGCCUUGUUUGGGUUGUGUGGUAUCAUUAAACCCAAGCGUAUGACAGUGUGAGAUAGUUUCUGUUUUCCAGGCUUUGCUUAAAUAGGGGUCCACAUUAGCACCUGAUACAGAGGGGUUAUAGAAGGAAAGUGAUUAAGAUGAAUGCCUUGUGAUCUGGAGCUGGUGUCUAAGGGGAUUGCUCGUUUCUGCCUCACCUGGAUUGUUUUGGGAUUUGUCUUUUUGGGGUAGUUUGUUUCUGAUAGUGCAUAGAGCCCAUAGUAUUGAAUGGUACAGGAGACUUCCAUUUCACUUCCUGAAAAUUAAAGGGCUUUGCCCUUCCUUUCACAAAACUGUAGAUUCCUUUAAUACAGGGUUCUCAUGUGGGACACAGUGAAAUUUUGUAGUGCUGCUUUUUAAUUACUACCUUCUGAAAUGCAAAAGCUUUGGUAUGGUGUAAUAUCAUUAAGUACAUUUUCUGUUCUGUCCCUGAAGGGGUUUUCUUCAAUCCUAAAUGUAUGAGGUUAUUGGCUGAAAUGUUACUCUGAAAUAUUUAGACCUUUGGCUAAUAAAGAUCAGACAAACCAGAGAACAUCCUCCGUUGUAAAGCUUUCUGCCCCCGGUCUUGUGGGCUAGUGGUGGCCCCCUUCUUCCUUCUUUGUUCCUCAAUACCGUAGUCCCAUUUACUUGUAACGCACCUCUUUUGUCCUGUAGUACGUUCUUACACUCCUUGACCUCCUCACCUCUUAGGGGUCUUUUUUUUAUUUUAUUUUAUUUUUUUUUUUGGAGACAGAGUCUUGCUCUGUUGCCGGGCUGGAGUGCAGUGGCGCGAUCUUGGCUUACUGCAACCUCCGCCUCCCGAGUUCAAGCAAUUUUCUUGCCUCAGCCUCCCAAGUAGCUGGGAUUACAGGCACGUGCCACCACACCCGGCCAAUUUUUGUAUUUUUAGUAGAGGGGGUUUCACCAUGUUGGCCAGGAUGGUCUCCAUCUCUUCACCCUCGUGAUCUGCCUGCCUCGGCCUCCCAAAGUGCUGUGAUUACAGGCAUGAGCCACUGCGCCUGGCCUAGGGGCUCUUUUAGAGUUUGUUUUCCAUAAAGUAAAUAGUCAUGGGUGACUAGUGUUUGUGAAGAGAUGAGAAAGAACAUCAUUCUAAUAAUCACCAUCCUGGAUAUAAUUUGUCAUCAGUCCAGGUGCAGUGGUGCAGGCCUGUAAUCCCAGCACUUUGGGAGGCUGAGGUGGGAGGAUCAGUUGAGGCCAGGAGUUGGAGACCAGCAUGGGCAGCAUAGCAAAACCCAAUCUAUUUAAAAAAUUGUUUAAAUGUAAAAAUUAAUCUAUUAUCAGACAACUGCUGUAUCUCCCUUAACUUGAACAACAUCCUGGACACACGUGUUCUGACAUAGGUCACCUCAAAAACCGACAGAAUAUGCUAGUUAAAUGCUCAAAUUCUUUCAUUUAAAAUUUUCUUAACAGGGAGAAAACACAAUUUUUCUGUAAAUGACGGAUUGCAGCUCGGUUGUGAGGACAUUGGAAAUAAGCCUGAGGAAGGCUGGCUGCCUUUAAACAGGAAGUUUGUGAUGAGUGACUUUUAAUCAAGUUACAACCAUUCAUAAUGGCUUAAAAAAUUGUUGUUUAUGUAUUCUUUCACUUCCUAAAACAAAAUAGCCAGUGUUUAUUGUCAUUGUGUCAGGUGAUGCACCAGGCAACUUCAUGUAUAUCAUGUAUAUCAUGCCAUCCGUACAUGUAACUGUUUUACAGAUGUGAAAACAGGCUUAGUGAUGAGAUCCAGGACCUACUCAGAAGGGCCCAGCAGUAACUCUGCCUCCAGAGCCGGCACCUCCGGUUCUGCCUCACAGUGUACUUCCCAAGUCCAUGAAGCUUCUCCUGACACCUAUGAGUUCUUCCAUUUGUCUUUUUAGUACUAUUUGACAUGCAAGCAUAAUCUCCUACAUUCCUUUUGCAGUGGAUAGUCAUAUUUUCCCUUCCUUUGGAAUGACUGACUAGAGUUAGAGAUAAAGCUGUGUAACUAAAUUUGUGUCUAUAGCGGUUUGAGACCAUAGGUAAGGAUUGGCUUGGCUAGGGGAGGAAUAUUGCAUGUUCUUGGUACUUGUUUUACAUUUCUUCCAGUACUAAAGCUCCAUGUGGUUCUAUUUUUUGUAAAUGAACACCCAUAAGUUUCCCAUCUGCGUUGUAAUCUCUCUGAACUUUGUUUCCCUAACAUAAAACAAGAGCGUUAGACCAGAUGACCUUCGAAGUACCUUCCGGUUUUACCAGGCCGCCAGUCUCUGUCCACAGCCCUGGGAUCAGUGGAGAUGCUUUAAGACCUCUGCACAGUGGGGGUAGCAGUGGGGGGUAUAGUGGUCUUUGAGGAUAUUCGGGCAAGAAGGAAACGAUUCUGGGAAAUGAACCAGCCUUAUGGAAGGAUCUAGGGUGUAAGCAUGUAGAUUAGCUAUUCUCAGCAGAUCUUGUGUUAAACACUUUCUAACAUUGAUUUACAUACUGUCUAUUGCUAACGUGUGUCUACUGACAACUCUUGUAAAAAAAGGGUUGGCAAAAGGUCAUGUUUUCCUUCUGUUUGCAAACAAAAUGGAUUAUUUUUAAAAGUUGUUGUUUUAUUAGUAACUCUUAAUGGGAACUCUGUUGAAUAGAUUUUCCUAGUUCAGUUUGUUUUCACUUGUGGAAGUGCAGGAAGAGCUGGUGUAAAAGAGAGGAAGGAGGAGGGAGGGAAUAAAGGCCAUGCCGGGAGCCUGCAUAACAAUCGCACACAUUGAGAAAGUUCACAGAAAUUAGAUUAAAUGCUUUGGGAAAAUGUAGUUUGUCUAGCAUUUUGAAAGAAUUUCUAGAAUUUCUGGGACAAUGAGUUCAUUUAAUCAUAUGUUCCAGUUUCUGAGUGUGAAGUUCUUUUUGUUGGAUUUGGUGGCUGUUGCUCACACCUUCACGCAGGGUGGUGGGCAGUUCUAGGUAGCUGGGGGUCUCUGGGGACCUUUCCGCUUUCCCUGUGAGUCCCCACAGGUUUUCCCUAGGAUGAUGCUCACAUCUGAAAUGCACGCUUCAGCUGCUAUGGAUUCCUGCCAUAAAGAAGAACCCACUAGAAUAAGAGCAAAUCACAUUGUGUAAAUUUUUUUUUUUUAAGACGGAGUCUUGCUCUGUUGCCCAGUCUAGAGUGCAGUGGUGCGAUCUCGGCUCACUGCAACCUCUGCCUCCCAGGUUCAAGUGAUUCUCCUGCCUCAGUCUCCCGAGUACCUGGGACUACAGGUGCCCACCACCAUGCCCAGCUAAUUUUUGUAUCUUUAGUAGAGAUGGGGUUUCACCAUAUUGCCCAGGCUGGUCUCGAACUCCUGAUCUUGUGAUCUGCCCUCCUCAGCCUCCCAAAGUGCCAGGAUUACAGGUGUGAGCCACCACGCCCGCCCACAUUGUGUAAAUUUAUCACCUGUUAAGGCAGAAAAUGAGCUUUGUAAACUAGUAAGCAGAAUUAUUUCUGCUCCCUCAAGGUGCACACAAGUAACCUCAGCCUUAAGUAUGUUCCUUUGAUUCUUCUUAACAGUGGUGAAGGCAAGGGGAUAGUUUUUUCAGCCAGCAGUGGGGUUGCAGGUAGAAUCACAGAGCUUUGCUUUGAACCCUAACUGGACAGAUCAUUUUCUGAGUCUUAAUUUUUCCUUUUCCAUUUCUAAAGUGAAGCCAGUAAUACCUGCCUUAUAGGGCUGUUGCAAGGAUGGAAUGAGAUGUAUUGACAGCAGUAAACUAUAAAAUACAUAGUUUAUAUAAUAAACUAUGAAAUAAAUACAAAAAUAUAAAACACGGGGUAUGAAGGCCAUCUAAGGGUUUCAUGAGCAAGGUGUAUUCAGCCUUAAGUUGAGGUUUUGCAUUAUUUUUGGUUAAAUAUAAAGACCAGGGUAAUCAUAGAACUGCCAAGCAGAAAGAAAUGUAGAAUGUAGCAGUGGUGUGGAGACCCGUGGCUGACAGGUGGUGGUCUUCAUAUAGGCUGAGGGACAGGCUAGAUGCAUGUCAAGUGGCAGCUCAGGUUGGAAGACAGGAGUUGGGGAUGUGAGAGUCCAGGCCAGGGUGAAGAGAAGUGGCUGGGAAGGCAGCCAGGCUCAGCUCUUAGGAGGCAGAGAGCUGCAAGCAGAGGGUGGGACCAGGUCUCUUUUUUCAACCCAGUCUUGAGGGAUGGGGGCAAAGUCAACCUAGACUUGAUUUAGAGCUAGUUCUGUUCACUUGAUCAUCUUUAUUGGGCCUUCAGGCUCCUAGAAGACUACCGUGAUAGACUGACUAGUGGUCUGUAAAUGGUUUUUAUUAAAAAAAUCACAUACCCUUUUUGAUAAAACAUGUAUUUGUUUAUACACUUUAAAUAUAUUGUGUAAUUAUAUAAUACAUUCACAAAUAAGAAUUUUAAAAGAAUGAGAUAAAAAAUUUAAAGUAGGCCAGGCGCAGUGGCUCACGCCUGUAAUCCCAGCGCUUUGUGGAGACUGAGGCAGGCAGAUCACGAGGUCAGGAGUUCGAGACCAGCCUGGCCAACAUGGUGAAACCCCGCCUGUACUAAAAAUACAAAUAAUUAGCCAGGCGUGGUGACAGGUGACUGUAAUCCCAGCUACUCAGGAGGCUGAGGCAGGAGAAUCGCUUGAACCUGGGAGGCAGAGGUUGCAGUGAGCCAAGAUCAAGCCACUGCACUCCAGCCUGGGCAACAGAGUGAGACUCUGUCUUUAAAAAAAAAAAAAAAAUGAAAGUCAAUGAAAGUUGUAAAGAUUUCAUCCUGCACUUCAGUGGCUGAUGAUUGCCUUAGACAGUGGGUCUGGGAGCAUCCUGGGGAGGGCAUGUGUCCUCAGGGGUCUCUGGGGACCAGCCUCAGCACCUCACUUCUUCCAGCCACAGAGACAGAACAUCAGAACCAUCCUUCAUGGAGCUUCCCAACUGGCCUGUUGAGGUCCCUGCUCUGCCAACCCCUGCUGCUGCUCUGCACAUGCUGGCUGUGUCCAGAGCUCGGAGGCCCCUGGCCCCAGCAAUGUGUGAUGCCUGCACAUGUGGCUUGGCUGCAGCACCUUGAGAAGACUUAAAUAUUCUAGUGACAUUGGCUGACCAGGGCACUGACAGCCUCACCUUAGUAUUUGAAUCAGUUCUGAGGCAAUAUCUAGUGUCAAGAGAAAAAUGAACUGUUUUUCCCAAACCAGUCAAUCUUUCCAGUAAUUAACAUAUAAAAAAGCCUCAUGUUAAGUGAGAGCAGUGCAGUGUGUGGUUAUAAAGAAAUAAGACUAAUGUUUAUGACAUACAUAGGUCUGUAAAACACAGACAUAUGUUAUUUUAUGGAUGCUAUUAUGCCAGUAGUGAUAACAGUAACAUUAGCUAAUAGAGAUUAAGGUAAGCCUUUCCACGCAUACUAUCUCAUUUAAUCUUUGCACCAACUUUGUAAAUGUAGGAAAUACUAAUCUGUUCAACAGAUACUUGAGUGCCCCUAUGGUGUUGGUGCUGUGAGGAUACAGUGUACAAGAAGACAGACAAAGGUCCCUGUGCUCACUUGAGCAGCUCACAGUGUAGUGGGAAGUCAGGCAUGCCCCCCCACCGCCCCAGGGAUCAGACAUAGUGGAAUCAUAAAGAGGGGUGAGUAAGUAAGGUCCCAUGUUAGAGCUGCAGGAUGGGAUGAGGUCAUCAAGAAAUGCUUCUGGAGGGGCCAGUUGGGCUGAGACAGAAGCUGGGGCAUGGAGGGCAGGGUGGCAGCCUUUGGAGAGAAAAGGUCCGUGUUCCUGGACAGUCUAUGGGUUGUGUCAUCCUAUUAAGUGGCUCUUUACGUGUACUUAUUUUCUCCCCAGGUAGAUCAAAAGCUUCUGGAGGGCAUGUUCUGUGUCUCAUUCCUUCAUGUCUUUCGCUACUCCUUCCACAAAAUAGUUUCCAGUAAAUGUUAGUUGACAUGAAUUGGUACUCAAAUGGAUGGUUAAAAGAUGUGUAUUGUGUAAGACACCAUAUCUUCCUUGUAAUUUUUUUGGGGGUCAAGCAACAAACAGUUAUUGAGGCUAUGAUAUUAGAAAUUAAAGACAAGCUUUAGCCCAUUUGCUCUUUAAGGAACUCAGAAUCUGAACAUAGAACAGCCAGCAGAGCAGGUUGAACAAGCAAGUACACCAUGUCGGGGUUCCCCGACUACACCAUGUCGGGGUUCCCCGACUCCCCCAUCUGUGGAGCUCAUUGGGUCAGGCUUCCCAGGAAGCACAUGCUGCACUGCUUGGGGUGGCCAGGCAUGCAGAUGGCAGAUGGGGUGUGUGCAGAGGCUUGUGAGUGGGGCUGCAGAGAAACAAGCUAGUGGAGAGGAGAUUGGCUGGCUUGUGUUUCUCUAGUGCCGUCAUGUAGAAACGCUGGAUUUGGGCAAGUGAUUGACAGGGCAUGAACCUCUGUCCUGACAUCCUGCCUCUGUCCUCAGGUAAUAUUUGUUGAGAGUUCAAGGGCAUAAUAUUUCAGAGCCCAGCAGUCUCACGCGGCUCUGCUGCGAAGUCCUUCUGGUGAACUGCUCUUCCAUCCAGCCUCUCCUGUGGCCAGUAGGGGAGUGCAGACACAACGUCGUUAAUAGCAACACAUUUUUACAAAAUUUACCUUUUCAAACCCCACCCCCUAGAAACCGUAGCUUCUUUAAUGUCCCGCUGGCUGUGUGAAAAACAGGAAUUUAUGUAACAAGUCCUGCACAGCAAACCUUUUCCUGUUCGGAAAAAAUUUUAAUUGUUGGCAAAGUUAGGAAACAGCUCUGUUACUCAAAGAGCGACCUGAAAUGUCCUCUUAGAAAAAUAUGUAAUAUGAUGUUUUGAUAAGUAGGAGACUGCUGUGGCUUUUUUUUUUUUAAAGUCUAAAUUAGUAUAUGUCCCACCUGAGUUAGUGAACGCUUCUUGAAUGUUUUAAAGAUUUCCUUAUUAUGUCUCCUGCAGUCUUUUUAAAAAUGACCCCCAGCUGGGCUUGCCAGUGAUCUGACAGGCUUAUCAUGAAUGUUAGAGAGCUUCACCCCCUCUCCCCAAGUCAAUGCAACAACCAGGAAGCUUCUAUCUGGGAAGAUCUUUCUUCCCCCUUUAUCAUUAACUAAAUGUGACAGGGACAGGAGUCAAGCUUCCUCUCCUCCAGAGAUUUCAUCGGAGCUUAUCUGUGUGUCUAUUGUGUUCAAAGAACAAAACUGUCAUGAUGGAAUAUUGUGCAAAUGCCUGGACUUCCAGUGUAUAGAAAAUGUCAGGGUCAGACUGCAGGGCUGCAUUCCAGUGCUACCCCAAGUGCGGGCCUGCUGAUCUUAAGGAGGAAUUAAGAACUCGGUUCGGCUGGGGUUGGUGGGUACAGCAGACAAGGCUGUGGCUCUGUGAGCAUACAUGUGUGUGUGUGGCGCCUUCCCAUAGGAAUUUGGGGAUCUUAGGGGAAUGCAAUAGGAUGGGAGGGAAAUGUACUCCCUGGCCUCUUUUAGGGAUUCUUGUACCUACUCUAAGCCCCUGGCCCUCCUCACAGCGUGUCUCGAGGUGAGGGUAGAUCUUGGGUGUGGAGGAAGGUGGGGAUUCUUGGGAACAGGAGACAGUCACUGCCAUCACCACACACCUGCUCCGUUCCAGCCGGGAAUCUGGGGCUCCGGUGGUGUCUUCCCCGCUCUCACACUUCACUGUAUGCUCUGGCAGGAGGGCUUGUCACGUAGCUGCUGUGUUGAAAUCUUUAGGCGGAAUGCAGUACAGAGAGUCAGAGGGCGUUUUGAAAUGUGGAUUUCUCAGCCCUGACUGCUGGGCCUUACCCUGACUUUUGCAUCUCCCUUUAGAAAGUGAGACCCCUCCAUUUUCUCUCUUCUACCACCUUUUAAUGAGAGAAGACUUCUCUCCCAGUUUGUGUUGGAGCCAGGCCUCAUCCUGCUGUGCAGAGGCUCUGCUCAGGCGCAGUGGUUGGCACUCGGGCCCGGGCGUCCCAUGUCAAUGGCAUGAGGAUGUGGGCGCUGUGGCUGCACCCCUGGGUGACCACAAAUCCAGCCAGAGCCUUUUUGUGGUUGAGAAGAGGGGCCGCAGAGAUGCAGGGGGCAUGGUCAGCUGAGCCUUGCAUCCAGUUGGCAGAGGAGGCCAAGAAAGCUGGGAGACUGUGCACAUUCCAGGGUCUUAGGGCACCCAGAAUCCCACUCCUUGGGAGCAGACCUCUGAGGAAAGAGGCUGCUGAAUGAACAAGGUGUAGUGGCUGUGUGCCCUGUACUGUGCUGGGGGCCAGAAGCUAUAAGACAAGGCCCUUCCUUCUGGGGAGCUCACAGCGUUUCCCUCGUCUCCUUUUCCACGUGUCCCACGGACUCCCCUGAACACCAUCUUACUCUGUGUUGUAGAGGAGGUGAAUCAAACCAUGGCUUUCUCAUCUGCAGCCUGGCUCUGGUGUUUCUGCUGAAACUUGGAGAGACCACCUCUGGCCCCUUUCACCAUAUAUUUGCAGUUGUGGAAUUCAAUUCGUCAUAAUCUGUCCCUACACAGCAAGUUCAUUCGUGUGCAGAAUGAAGGAACUGGAAAAAGUUCUUGGUGGAUGCUCAAUCCAGAGGGUGGCAAGAGCGGGAAAUCUCCUAGGAGAAGAGCUGCAUCCAUGGACAACAACAGUAAAUUUGCUAAGAGCCGAAGCCGAGCUGCCAAGAAGAAAGCAUCUCUCCAGUCUGGCCAGGAGGGUGCUGGGGACAGCCCUGGAUCACAGUUUUCCAAAUGGCCUGCAAGCCCUGGCUCUCACAGCAAUGAUGACUUUGAUAACUGGAGUACAUUUCGCCCUCGAACUAGCUCAAAUGCUAGUACUAUUAGUGGGAGACUCUCACCCAUUAUGACCGAACAGGAUGAUCUUGGAGAAGGGGAUGUGCAUUCUAUGGUGUACCCGCCAUCUGCCGCAAAGAUGGCCUCUACUUUACCCAGUCUGUCUGAGAUAAGCAAUCCCGAAAACAUGGAAAAUCUUUUGGAUAAUCUCAACCUUCUCUCAUCACCAACAUCAUUAACUGUUUCGACCCAGUCCUCACCUGGCACCAUGAUGCAGCAGACGCCGUGCUACUCGUUUGCGCCACCAAACACCAGUUUGAAUUCACCCAGCCCAAACUACCAAAAAUAUACAUAUGGCCAAUCCAGCAUGAGCCCUUUGCCCCAGAUGCCUAUACAAACACUUCAGGACAAUAAGUCGAGUUAUGGAGGUAUGAGUCAGUAUAACUGUGCGCCUGGACUCUUGAAGGAGUUGCUGACUUCUGACUCUCCUCCCCAUAAUGACAUUAUGACACCAGUUGAUCCUGGGGUAGCCCAGCCCAACAGCCGGGUUCUGGGCCAGAACGUCAUGAUGGGCCCUAAUUCGGUCAUGUCAACCUAUGGCAGCCAGGCAUCUCAUAACAAAAUGAUGAAUCCCAGCUCCCAUACCCACCCUGGACAUGCUCAGCAGACAUCUGCAGUUAACGGGCGUCCCCUGCCCCACACGGUAAGCACCAUGCCCCACACCUCGGGUAUGAACCGCCUGACCCAAGUGAAGACACCUGUACAAGUGCCUCUGCCCCACCCCAUGCAGAUGAGUGCCCUGGGGGGCUACUCCUCCGUGAGCAGCUGCAAUGGCUAUGGCAGAAUGGGCCUUCUCCACCAGGAGAAGCUCCCAAGUGACUUGGAUGGCAUGUUCAUUGAGCGCUUAGACUGUGACAUGGAAUCCAUCAUUCGGAAUGACCUCAUGGAUGGAGAUACAUUGGAUUUUAACUUUGACAAUGUGUUGCCCAACCAAAGCUUCCCACACAGUGUCAAGACAACGACACAUAGCUGGGUGUCAGGCUGAGGGUUAGUGAGCAGGUUACACUUAAAAGUACUUCAGAUUGUCUGACAGCAGGAACUGAGAGAAGCAGUCCAAAGAUGUCUUUCACCAACUCCCUUUUAGUUUUCUUGGUUAAAAAAAAAAACAAAAAAAAAAACCCUCCUUUUUUCCUUUCGUCAGACUUGGCAGCAAAGACAUUUUUCCUGUACAGGAUGUUUGCCCAAUGUGUGCAGGUUAUGUGCUGCUGUAGAUAAGGACUGUGCCAUUGGAAAUUUCAUUACAAUGAAGUGCCAAACUCACUACACCAUAUAAUUGCAGAAAAGAUUUUCAGAUCCUGGUGUGCUUUCAAGUUUUGUAUAUAAGCAGUAGAUACAGAUUGUAUUUGUGUGUGUUUUUGGUUUUUCUAAAUAUCCAAUUGGUCCAAGGAAAGUUUAUACUCUUUUUGUAAUACUGUGAUGGGCCUCAUGUCUUGAUAAGUUAAACUUUUGUUUGUACUACCUGUUUUCUGCGGAACUGACGGAUCACAAAGAACUGAAUCUCCAUUCUGCAUCUCCAUUGAACAGCCUUGGACCUGUUCACGUUGCCACAGAAUUCACAUGAGAACCAAGUAGCCUGUUAUCAAUCUGCUAAAUUAAUGGACUUGUUAAACUUUUGGAAAAAAAAAGAUUAAAUGCCAGCUUUGUACAGGUCUUUUCUAUUUUUUUUUGUUUAUUUUGUUAUUUGCAAAUUUGUACAAACAUUUAAAUGGUUCUAAUUUCCAGAUAAAUGAUUUUUGAUGUUAUUGUUGGGACUUAAGAACAUUUUUGGAAUAGAUAUUGAACUGUAAUAAUGUUUUCUUAAAACUAGAGUCUACUUUGUUACAUAGUCAGCUUGUAAAUUUUGUGGAACCACAGGUAUUUGGGGCAGCAUUCAUAAUUUUCAUUUUGUAUUCUAACUGGAUUAGUACUAAUUUUAUACAUGCUUAACUGGUUUGUACACUUUGGGAUGCUACUUAGUGAUGUUUCUGACUAAUCUUAAAUCAUUGUAAUUAGUACUUGCAUAUUCAACGUUUCAGGCCCUGGUUGGGCAGGAAAGUGAUGUAUAGUUAUGGACACUUUGCGUUUCUUAUUUAGGAUAACUUAAUAUGUUUUUAUGUAUGUAUUUUAAAGAAAUUUCAUCUGCUUCUACUGAACUAUGCGUACUGCAUAGCAUCAAGUCUUCUCUAGAGACCUCUGUAGUCCUGGGAGGCCUCAUAAUGUUUGUAGAUCAGAAAAGGGAGAUCUGCAUCUAAAGCAAUGGUCCUUUGUCAAACGAGGGAUUUUGAUCCACUUCACCAUUUUGAGUUGAGCUUUAGCAAAAGUUUCCCCUCAUAAUUCUUUGCUCUUGUUUCAGUCCAGGUGGAGGUUGGUUUUGUAGUUCUGCCUUGAGGAAUUAUGUCAACACUCAUACUUCAUCUCAUUCUCCCUUCUGCCCUGCAGAUUAGAUUACUUAGCACACUGUGGAAGUUUAAGUGGAAGGAGGGAAUUUAAAAAUGGGACUUGAGUGGUUUGUAGAAUUUGUGUUCAUAAGUUCAGAUGGGUAGCAAAUGGAAUAGAACUUACUUAAAAAUUGGGGAGAUUUAUUUGAAAACCAGCUGUAAGUUGUGCAUUGAGAUUAUGUUAAAAGCCUUGGCUUAAGAAUUUGAAAAUUUCUUUAGCCUGUAGCAACCUAAACUGUAAUUCCUAUCAUUAUGUUUUAUUACUUUCCAAUUACCUGUAACUGACAGACCAAAUUAAUUGGCUUUGUGUCCUAUUUAGUCCAUCAGUAUUUUCAAGUCAUGUGGAAAGCCCAAAGUCAUCACAAUGAAGAGAACAGGUGCACAGCACUGUUCCUCUUGUGUUCUUGAGAAGGAUCUAAUUUUUCUGUAUAUAGCCCACAUCACACUUGCUUUGUCUUGUAUGUUAAUUGCAUCUUCAUUGGCUUGGUAUUUCCUAAAUGUUUAACAAGAACACAAGUGUUCCUGAUAAGAUUUCCUACAGUAAGCCAGCUCUAUUGUAAGCUUCCCACUGUGAUGAUCAUUUUUUUGAAGAUUCAUUGAACAGCCACCACUCUAUCAUCCUCAUUUUGGGGCAGUCCAAGACAUAGCUGGUUUUAGAAACCCAAGUUCCUCUAAGCACAGCCUCCCGGGUAUGUAACUGAACUUGGUGCCAAAGUACUUGUGUACUAAUUUCUAUUACUACGUACUGUCACUUUCCUCCCGUGCCAUUACUGCAUCAUAAUACAAGGAACCUCAGAGCCCCCAUUUGUUCAUUAAAGAGGCAACUACAGCCAAAAUCACUGUUAAAAUCUUACUACUUCAUGGAGUAGCUCUUAGGAAAAUAUAUCUUCCUCCUGAGUCUGGGUAAUUAUACCUCUCCCAAGCCCCCAUUGUGUGUUGAAAUCCUGUCAUGAAUCCUUGGUAGCUCUCUGAGAACAGUGAAGUCCAGGGAAAGGCAUCUGGUCUGUCUGGAAAGCAAACAUUAUGUGGCCUCUGGUAGUUUUUUUCCUGUAAGAAUACUGACUUUCUGGAGUAAUGAGUAUAUAUCAGUUAUUGUACAUGAUUGCUUUGUGAAAUGUGCAAAUGAUAUCACCUAUGCAGCCUUGUUUGAUUUAUUUUCUCUGGUUUGUACUGUUAUUAAAAGCAUAUUGUAUUAUAGAGCUAUUCAGAUAUUUUAAAUAUAAAGAUGUAUUGUUUCCGUAAUAUAGACGUAUGGAAUAUAUUUAGGUAAUAGAUGUAUUACUUGGAAAGUUCUGCUUUGACAAACUGACAAAGUCUAAAUGAGCACAUGUAUCCCAGUGAGCAGUAAAUCAAUGGAACAUCCCAAGAAGAGGAUAAGGAUGCUUAAAAUGGAAAUCAUUCUCCAACGAUAUACAAAUUGGACUUGUUCAACUGCUGGAUAUAUGCUACCAAUAACCCCAGCCCCAACUUAAAAUUCUUACAUUCAAGCUCCUAAGAGUUCUUAAUUUAUAACUAAUUUUAAAAGAGAAGUUUCUUUUCUGGUUUUAGUUUGGGAAUAAUCAUUCAUUAAAAAAAAUGUAUUGUGGUUUAUGCGAACAGACCAACCUGGCAUUACAGUUGGCCUCUCCUUGAGGUGGGCACAGCCUGGCAGUGUGGCCAGGGGUGGCCAUGUAAGUCCCAUCAGGACGUAGUCAUGCCUCCUGCAUUUCGCUACCCGAGUUUAGUAACAGUGCAGAUUCCACGUUCUUGUUCCGAUACUCUGAGAAGUGCCUGAUGUUGAUGUACUUACAGACACAAGAACAAUCUUUGCUAUAAUUGUAUAAAGCCAUAAAUGUACAUAAAUUAUGUUUAAAUGGCUUGGUGUCUUUCUUUUCUAAUUAUGCAGAAUAAGCUCUUUAUUAGGAAUUUUUUGUGAAGCUAUUAAAUACUUGAGUUAAGUCUUGUCAGCCA